AGUUAAACAAGAGUCGGCACUGGGAACAGCUGUGCGUAGACCAGACCAGUGACUUAUAAGGUACUGUUUUUACUCAUUUAAAUCUUCAGGGUUCAUUUGUUUUGGGGACAAGUAUUUAGUGGUCAUUUGACCUUUUUUUCCUCCCUCUUCACCUCUAUUUUGAGAGAAAAUAUACCCUUGAAAAUAUUUUAGCUUUUUAACUGUAUUAUUUUCUGGCUGUUGAUAUUUGAAACUACUCGGAUUUUGCUUUGUUUUGUUAGUGUUUUUAGGAACCAGAUGAUUGUUGCUGUUGUUUUAUUUUAAAGCUUAGUUUAGGUUUGUUUCUUUGUUGUAUCUUGUCAUGUGUGGUUUUUGUGUUUUAUUGCUUGUGUUGGAUAAAGAUAAAUAUACUUUAGCAUUACAAAAUGUACAGAAUGUUCUUGACUGGGCAGGAGGGGGAGCUUAAUGAAUCUUCAACUUGAAAUAUAGAACUAAUAUGGAGCCAAUCAGACAAGAGAACCUGGGCAGGGCAGUCUAGGCACUUUAACUGAUUCAGUCAAGGCUCACUAAACUCAUCACAGCUUGGUAGAUCUGACCUGGGAAACACAGUUAUUUUGAAUUGGGGUUUUUGCCUCCAGUUUGCUUCUAUAUUUAGCUGUUAAUUUUAAUCCUUCCUUCUCUUUAUUCAUUAUUUUUUAAAAAAAUUCUAAUAAGCCUACUUUUCUUUUUUUAAUGAAGCUUAUCUUAGUGUAAGCUCAUUCACCUUAAUGGAGGAACAUUUCUAAGAAGAGUGAAAUUUUCAAAAAGAUUUCAAGUCACCGAUCCAUAGAGGGUCUUCCAGAGCAGAAGGGGAAUAGCCCAAUGCGGCACAGAAAAAAAUCCCUGUGUACCCUAGCAUUCCAGGUGUCACUCUUUCCCCGAGGCCCUGGCUAGCUGGUAUAUAAUAUUUGCUGCUGGCCAAUAAAACAACAAUGGAGAACAUUAAGGGUUUCAAUAUAUGUGAAUUUUCCAUAAAGUGAAGUUUAAAAAGUAAACUUUUACCACUGAAAACUUGAAAAGCUUUUCAAAGAAUUUAGCCACUUGUGGAUCAUUCUCUUCAUGAGAUCCACUAUAUGUUUUGAGCUCUCUCUGGAGGGGACUAAAUGCAAUUUAAUGUUCCCUUAAUUUCUCAGUAUUACUCAUGGAUACAUAUUAUAGAAUUUUUCUAUAAUGCAGUAAUACAUUGCAUGGUAUAUAAGGCUAUUAAUUCUUAGAUCAAAUGGUCACAUAAUCACUGUUUAUUUUUUAUUUUUUAGUUUUAUUUUUUUGAGAUGGAGUCUUGCUCUGUCGCCCAGGCUGGAGUGCAAUGGCACGCUCUUGGCUCACUGCAACCUCCACCUCCUGGAUUCAAGUGAUUCUCCUGCCUCAGCCUCCAGAGUAGCUGGGAUUACAGGGGCCUGCCACCAUGCCUGGCUAAUUUUUGUAAUUUUGGUAGAGAUGGGGUUUCACCAUGUUGGCCACGCUGGUCUUGAACUGCUGACCUCAUGAUCCACCCACCUCGGCCUCCCAAAGUGCUGGGAUUACAAACGUGAGCCACUGCGCCCAGCCUUUUUUUAAUUCUUGUAUUAUUUUUAUAGGACUUUUUUUUUCCUCCUGUGUCCACCUUCCAUAUUGAAGAGUGACUUCUUUACUUACUGGUGUAGACAGUUUGCAUAUCUCUAAUAACUUCCUUCAACCUCAACAACCUCUUCAUGAUUAUUUUGUGCUGGGAGCAAGAACACCAGAAAAUGAACAAGUUUAUAAAAAAUUAUGGACGAAUAAGAGGCAAUAACUUUAUCUGAGGGUCCAAGAGAUUCUCUUAUGAGAAACGUGCAUGUGCCAAAGGACAUAGACACAGUGACAUCUAUUUUGGGUGCUCAGGAGACACUUGGCUUGUGUCCAAGUUCUUAGUUGUGUUCUGUAGUAGAGGUUGCCAUGGAAGUAGUUCUGGAAUAAGUAAUGUGUUACUGCAUCUUAUACAGAAAGUGUGGUUUGUUCUUUUUAUAAAGUUACUGGAGGUGUGUGUCAAGGAAUCAGUGACUAAACAAAUCCCAAGAGGCAUACCUAAUAUUAAUCAAGCACUAAGUGUUUUAUUUUAGUCCCAUUCACAAUCACGCUGUUCACAUGCAUGUCUAGCUGGGAAACAGCAUAAUAAUGCUUUGUAGGAAAGAGAGAAAAGGAAAAAAAUAUUCAUUUUCUGGUUUAUUCAAUUCUUCUGUGUGGAGAUUAUGCUUAAGAAAACAAUGAAUAAGGCAAGAUUUAUUUUCUCAGUGAUUUUUCUGAUUUCUUGAAUGGCUUUCUAACUUACAAGUUCUUUUAAGCUGAAAAACACUACAAAGCAAUUUUAUAAACCAUGUACAAUGAAUUAGUAGCACAAUAUAUGACAAUAUGUGUUUUCUUCUAAUAUUUUUAUAUUGUGCAUUUUAGAGCAAAACGAAUCACUGAUUUCUCAAAGAUCUUGAAAAUGAUAGUAGUCACUUUUAUUAAUCUCACUCUACAAAAGAAAAAAACUGGAUAUAUUACAUACAUUUAUUAAGCUAUAAGCUGAGUCCAGGGCAAUUCUAUGUUUCAACUUUAAUUAGAUUCCUUGGCUAAAUACUUGAUCAUUUAACUUUAUUUGGAAUCACAUUGUGAAGACUUUUGUAUUAGAAGCUCAUUUUUCUUUAAUUUUUAAAAAAAUACAAGUUUCACCUAGUCACUGUAGAAAUUUUUCCUAAGUGUUAAAGCAUCAGAUGGUGUAUAUGACAAACUUUUCUGUUUGAAACAAUGAAUUAGAGACUGGCUUUUGUCUGCAAUAAUGAAUUUGGGAUAUGCAUAUGUUUGUUAACUUUGUCUAAAACAAUUCUCUAGGCCAGGCAUGGUGAUUCACACCUGUAAUCCCAGCACUUUGGGAGGCCAAGGCGGACGAAUCACUUGAGGUCAGGAGUUCGAGGGCAGCCUGGCCAACAUGGUGAAACCCCAUCUCUACUACAAAAAAUAAAAAAAUUAGCCAGGCACGGUGGCGCAUGUCUGUAAUCCCAGCUACCCGGGAGGCUGAGGUAGGAGCAUCACUGCAACCUGGUAGGCGGAGGUUUCAGUGAGCCGAGAUCACACCACUGCACUCCAAUAUGGGCAACAGAGUGAGAUUCUAUCUCAAAAAAAAAAAAAAAGAAAAAAAAAAGAAAAAAAAAACAAUUGUCUAGAAAUUGUGCUUAUUUUUGCUUCCUACCUUCAGUUAGGUGGCAUGACUUAUUUUAAAAUGAAAUGUUAUUCCAAUUGAAACACCGCUGUUUUAAACUGAAAAUAUGCUAUGUUAAGUCAAUUCAGUAAAGCUUUUCCUCACUUGACUCCUCUUUCAUUUUAAUCGAAAUUUAAUUUUCGUGUUCAUACCUAAAUAGGAAAUUCGACAUACUAAAGAAUAUGUAUUUUAAAUUUAGAACUUUUGUACCAUAAGACCUAAAUUUAAAAUUCCUGAAAUGUCAGUGUCAUUUUGAAUACACGCUUAGGAAGACUUCGAUUUAGAAAGAUACUUUUCAAACCUGGAAAAGGAAACAACCAUUUAAAUGAAUUAAUGCAUGUUAGCAUUCACUGAUAACACCUUAUAAGGGUGCUUCUUAGUACAACCUUAUGAGAAUUCUCCAGAAGCCUCAGAAUUCAGCCCCUUAUAAACUAGAAUUCAGUGAGCAAGAUUUAUGUUUCCCAAGGAACUGUCAAGCUUAGUGCUUUUGAUUGUGUUCAGGGAAGAGAAGAUAUUGAGAUUUCUGAAGUUGUUGAACAGAGAAAGAGAUAAAUGCUUUGUUCUUUGAAAAAUCCACAUUUAGUUCAUUUUCAAUUACAAUCUCCCAGGGAAAAAAGAUACUCAAACUGACUCAAGUAUGUUCCUACAUAUUGGCCUUUGUUUAACAUAUUAAAUUGGAGCUUCUGGACAGUUGAAGAGGUAAUAUGAAUCCAAGGUUCUUUUUGUAUUAAUACAUCUUAAUCAUGAAAUAAAUGUUUGUUGAAUGACUAUUACUUUCAAACCUUAAUUUAAAAAGACAUCGACAAAUAAAAUGAUGUUAAAACUGCUAUGUUUUAUUUCAUAUUUGAUUAUUGGAGUAUUUGUUACUUAGUAUACUGCUGAAUCAUGCUAAAACAUGAACAGUUCAUUAAGCAAAGCCAUUUAAUAAAUUCUGAAAUUACUGUUAGCAAACAGUAAUUUGGAACUGUAAAUUGCCAGAAGAAAAAGCAUCGGGUAUCUACAGUCAAUAAUAAUUCAGAAAGUGGAAUUGGAGGACAAGAAGGUCUCAAGUGUUAUUCUAUAACCCCCCUCCUUUUCUUUUUUGGUUUUGUUUCUUUUGCUGUAGGUAUUGUGGAAAUUAUUUGUUUUAUAUCAAUCAGAACACUUUGAAAAAAAAUUUUACUGUUGUGUAUUCUUCCAUUCUAUGGUUAUACUGUACAUAAUAGAACAUGGCUCCUAUUGUUGGGGACCUACAUUGUUUCAGUGACUUCUGCUGUGAAUAAAAUUAGGAUAAGCAUUCUUUUACAUAUGACUUUGCUCAUUUGAUUAUUUCAGAACUGAAAUGACUUGGAAAUUAGUGAGUCCUGAUCACUUUUUUUUUUUUAAGAGUAGGAGAACUAGUCCUGAAAUAUCACUGAUCUAGAACCUUGGCUUCCAAGCUUUCAGUCUAAUAUCUGUAUCUAGCCAGAAGUAAUGACUGAGUGACAAAUACAUAAGGGGGCAGGAAGUGAAAGCAUAAUUUCCUUCUGUCUGAGUAAGAGGUCAAUCAUGUACCCCAUUCUCUGAAAAUCCCCAGGGAGUGGAAGGGUUCUCAUACUAAAGAAAACAGUCACGAUUCCAUGCCAGACUUUAUUCUCAAGGAGUGAUAAACAUAUGAUAGCUAUGGGAACAUUUUUAAAUAGCUGUCAUUUUGUUAAUGAGUAUUUGCUAAAGCAUUUCCUGGGCCACUGGUGUUUAUGGAACUUUUAAACAAAAUAUUUAUGAAGAUGGAACCGGGACUUGCUUCAUAAAUUAUGUCCUUUUACUUGCACCUUUGCUUUUCCUCACUGCACAACGAUGUUCAGGCCUCUUCUACAUGAAACAAACAAACAAAUCUUCAGCCUUUUCAACCAUGUUCUUUUUUCCUGGUGCCAAGAAAAAUUUAUAUUUUUUGUUUCUUCUCCCUUGCCUCCCUCUGAGUUGAUUGCCCUUUGCACUUUGGCAUUAUUUCUACCACAAUAUUGAAAUGACCUCUCAGAGGUUGCUCAUGAUGGCUGAAUUAACAGUUAAAUUCAACAGCUUUUUAUCUCUGUCUUCACCUUCUGUUCUUUCUGCCAUCUAUACUGUUUACCCUCAUGCUCUUCUUGAAAUAGUUCUGUCUUUUGAUAUUAGAGAUCUUGUAGAGAUCUAGUGCAUAGCCUAUGGCUCUGCCCCUCUCCUAGGCUUUUUUUUUUCUUCCCUCUUGUUAGAGGGCUCCUGUUUUCUUCCCACCUUCUUGGUUUCAGUGUCUGUGUUUAUUUUGUUUUCUCUCUUAGUCUUUCUUCCUUGGAAAAUUUCAUAUAGGCCUAUGGCUUCAUCUUAAAGCUCAAUGUGGAUAUCUGAUCAGCAAAGCCUCUUCCACCCUUUGUGCGAGUUGUAACAAACGUCCCCUUCCUCCAGAUGCACAAUGCUCGCAUCAGGAUCUUCAGCUUGGCAGCAAACUGAGCUGGAUUUCAGCCCCUGCUCAGCCUGCACAACCUCAGACAGUUGCCCUGCUGGUCAGGGCCUCCUAUUCAAUGCUGUCUAUGGUAUUCCAGUGCUUCAAACUCCAUGUCUUUCCCUCAGUCAAACUAGCCUUCCAUCUUUCAUCUCCUCCAUCACUUUUUAUACAACCAGGUGCCAAUUAGAAUUUUAGCAACCAUUUCCUUGGCAUUUUUCCUUUUUAUUUCCAUGGCCACAUUCUUGCUCAGAAUUUAAUUCCCUCUUGUUAGCCUACUGUCCCCGCCCCAAUCCUUUUCUACUACAGUCUAUCCUCUAUACAUUUGGCAAUUUGAAGAUGAUUAUAUAUCUCUAUCUAUCUAUCUAUCUAUCUAUCUAUCUAUCUAUCUAUCUAUCUAUCUAUCUCUCUAUCUCUCUAUCUGCUUUCCUAUCUAGAUAUAGACACAUAAAUAUAGAUAGAUAUAAUUAUACCCCCCAACUUUUCAAUGAGUCCUUAGCAGAUGGACAGAAGCAGAGGCUGUAAAGUUGAAUUUCAGAAUUUGAGGUCCAGCUUUGGUGCAUUCACGUGUGUCAUCCUGUGUGUUACUCAGUUUCAGGGUGUCAAUAAUGAAUAACCUAUGUCAAAACCUUCUAUGUGCCAGCCACAGUGCUCUGAGCAUUUCCCAUAUAUUGUUCAUUCAGCACUCAAAAGAAAACAUUUUGUUCUGUUUGUACUAGACAUUAUAAAAAUGGAAUCAAAUUUAUCUUAAAGAGACUGCUUUAUUCUCUGAGUUCAAUUUGGGUUUUGAAGAAGUCUACAGUAAAGUUAAAUUCAGAUAAUACCAAUGGUCUUGGCCCGAUUGCAAGUGGUGGUAAAACAAAGGCAAGUGAGUAUUAUAUUUUAUUUUGAGAUAAAAUCAUCUCCUUGUUCUGUUUUUGUUGUUGUUGUUGUUAUUUUGUUUUGUUUUGUUUUUUUAAGAAAGAGCAGCAAGAAAAGUAAAACAGAUUUUUUUUCUUUUUAACAAUUACAAACUACAUAACGCAAAUAAACACUUUCCUUUGUUCAAUGCUUAUAUGUGGUUUUCUUUAUUUAUUCUUAGUGUCACAAAACAAGCAACUGGAGUAGCCAGAAACCUAUCCCACAUUUUUUGACACCAGGCUGCCUCAUUUGCCAGAAUACUGUCCUUUCUUUCAAUUUAAGAAUCCAUCAGUGCCGUUGUCAAAUUUAAGUGGAAAUACUUCAAAGUAAUGACUAAGGGUCUUCAGACAUGUGCCAGGAAUAUUAUUUUGCUAUAACUGCUACCCUAGAGUCAUAAAUUAAUUUUCCAGAGUGACACCUCCUUGUCACUUUGGGAAGAUAAAGUGACCAUCAUUUCUUAUACCCAGUAUGGGUUUUUGGAAGGCUGUUGUUAGUGUUUCUUCUAAUGCUUCUCUCAGAGACCACUACUACCUUUUUUUUUUAUUUCUGUAAAAGGACUUAGGCUUUUUCUUAACAUCUAUGGCCUAUUUCAUUUCCUUAAUUAACUAAUUACUUAUAAAUGGAAGUUGCAUAAGUCAUACAAUUGGGAAGUUGGAUGGGAUCUUAAUGAUCUCGUAAUUAACCCCCACAUAUUUCUCUAAUGACCAAAACUGUCCAAACUAAGUUAAGAACUUAUCAAUAAUCACAUAGCAACUCUAGAAUGUGUUUCCUCAUUAAGAACCUGCAGCCAUACUGGCAACUUCUUGGAGUAUUAAUUCCAUUGCAAAGUCUCAAACCUGCAGCAGAAAUAAACCUGAGGCUUCUCUUCCUUUCUCUCUUCAUCUUUGGCUGUCAGCAGGAAUAACAUCUUAGAAAUCCAUCCUCUUUCAUUCAUAGGAGCUACUUUUUAGUAGGGGAAGCCUUCCACACAAUGUUUUCUUGACUUUGAACUUCUGUAGCUCUUGAAAUGGGAAUUAGUGGCAUACAUAACAAAUAAAAUAAUAAAAUAUUUAUGAAUCGCCCCCAAAGUGCAGCUCCCAAUGCUCCACAGUAUUCUCUGAAGUAAAGCAAAUCUUUGUGUCAGAGAUAUGCAUUUCAAAAAGUAUUAACAUGAUAUUGUGGCAGUUUUAUAAUAUGAAGUACUGUAUCUCUUAUGAACACACACACACAGAGAUAUUGGGGGAAAUUGUUUGGGACAACAAACCCAAUUAGAGUAAAUGUUGAAUGCUUCCCUUCUUCCUUCCCCUCAGGCUUGUCACUAACUCUGCCCACUUUCUCAUAUACAUGGCUGGCUUCAGCAUUUCUGUACUUUCUCACCUUUGUAUGGUUUGCCACAUGCAGGUGGUUUUUCAGCCCAGAGAAGUUUUCCCAGUUCUUGUUUUUCUGGAAUCAUUACUUCUGAAUCACUUUACUUCAUCCCUCCUCUUUCAAAACUUUGCUGUGACUUUCAGCACUUCACAUUUUGACUUCUUACUAACCAGUCCAUUCAAGCUCAGCUGGACUGUAAGCUCUUUGAGGGCAGGGGCUUUGUCUUACAUAUUUGUCUGAGCACAGUGUUUCACCCACAAAUCCCAAAUUUUGGGGUCCAGUAUUGCUCUGGUCUUGUUACAAAUGUGGACAUAUCCUCUGUGAGAAUGUGCUGACAGAUUGCCCGGCCUGUCGCAGUGGACAUUUAAUUAAGUGACUGGAAAGUUAAAAGACACUAACAAGAGGAUAUGAGCUUGCUUUUCUUCCCUUUUGGUAAAAUAUUCCAGGCCUUUGCUCUCCAUAUAUUUCAUUUCUUAUUUGCUCAGAUUUCAUAAUAAAGCAGAUGACCAUUCAGGUGACUCAUUCAACUUUGUUUAUCUUAGAUUCUUCACCAUUUGUUGGAGUUUCAGCAGUUGUGCUUCACAUGAUGGGGACUUAGACUCAAUGCUGACAUUUGAGAGAUAUUUUGAGAUGUUAGCUCGUGGUCUACCUCCUUGCAUUUGGCUUUGCUCCAAUCCCAUUUAUUUUGUGACAAAUAUUGCCUAAGAAAAGGGAUAAUUCAAAAAAAAGUGUUUUGGAUUUUUUGUUUGUAACAGCUUUUGAGUUUCAAAAAAAUCUAACUCCAUAAGGACUCAGGGUUCAAAUUUUAAAUUAUAAUGACAACAACAAAAUAAAACAGAUUUCUUUACCCUACCACUAAGAGCAAAUAAUGCAGAUAUUAAUAAUUUUCAUGGUAAUGGAGCCAAAGGCAGAAUCAGAGGAGAUACAAAGAGACAUCAGGUUCUUGAGGGGUGGCAGGAUCCUAAGUGCUCCAAGUUCUGCCACACCAUGCUGGGUACUCCCUGAGCUGAGUACAUGGGGGACAGAACUGAAAACCCAGAUCACACUGGGAAAAUCUAAGAGCAAAGGAACCUGUAGAUCACUUCCCAUGUAAAGUGCAUGAAGGCUGCAAAACUUGAAUCACUUUUUAGUGCCCUGCAUAGUGCCAGGUCAUUAGAAAUGGGUGUCUAAGAAGAUGUGUCCAAAACAGCCUCCCAGGUUAACCCCAUGCCCUAAAUGCAGCCAAGAAAGGAAGAGAAGGAGUGGUGAGAGAGACAAAUCCAGAGAAGCCCAAACGUAGCCACAGGGUCUGUGGACUUAAGCCUAGGAACACACAGGGAUGAGGAAGCCAGUAUAUCAGAGAUGCCUAUGUGCGCAGGAGAUGAUGACCACAGACCAGAUUCCCCCUCAUCCCCACCCAGGACAUGUAACUCUCUCUGUUCCUGACAUCAGAUGAUAUAAAGAAAGUAAGUUAAUCAAAAUUAAGUUUCAGCCACCUGGCAAUAUAAAAAAAUAAGGAAGUUAUGUCUUAUACACCUGGUUUUAUAGACUAACAUCUAUUCCUUCUACACAAAUUAUAUUUUAAACUUAAACCAAUCAUUUUUAGCUAUCUAUUUUGCUAUUAAAAAUUUUGGUUGGUAAUAAUGGUUUAUAAUCUUAUCGAAAGUGUAAAGUAUACUUUAUUUUUUUGAAGCUGGAGGGAUUUCAAAGCUUGAAAUACGAAGUGUAGGAUUUGACCUGGUUAGGUCUUGACCAUAGAGGUGAGAGGAUUAGGGAAUAAUAAAGUAAUCUUACAGGAGAAUCUCCACUUUAGACGGUUUAAUAGAGCUUCAGAUUUUAGUUUAUAUUUCAUACAAAUUCUGGUCUCUAAGGAUCACAAACAUUUAUUAUCUUUCCACUCCUUACCAGUGUUAUCUUAAGUGACACAAAGCAAAUGCAGAAAUUUUCAUAAAUCACUCAAAAGGAUUGUUGCUUGGCUGAAAGUGCCUUAUAAACUGAGCCCAUACUGGUAAUGAGUGAUCUUUUCCCAAGUUCUUAAAGUACAGCUAAGAUUCCCAGAAAGUAACACCCGUUCUAAGAUAUGGGCUCCAUUGAGAUCAAGGACAGAAAGGAAAAUUACUUCUGUUUUCUCGAGGAUGUGGCAUAAUAAGAAAUACAUAUUUGGCCUUUGUUCCUUUCUCCUGGGACACAGCUUUCAAAAUCCAUGGAAUCUCUAGAGUGAUGAGAGUGUCUUUUGUAUGCUAAUGAGAUGACUUGUGGCUGGAGCCCCUAGAUAGCUCCAGCAUAGGGUCUGGUCUCCAGAAAGGCCAAGGCACAAUUAGAAUGUUGGAACUUUCAGUCCCAGCACUCAACCUCCAGAGGCAGGAGAGGGGCUGAAGUCUGAGUUAAUUACCCUUGGUCAAUAAUUUACUUAAUCAUGCCUAUGUAAUGGAACCUCCAUUAAAAAAAAAAAAAAAAAAGAUGGGAUUUUGGAGAGCACCUGUGUUGGUGAACACAUCAAGAUUCAAAGAGAUGCAUGCCCAUAAAUGGCAUAGAAACUCUACAGAGAAUCAAAGAAAAGGCAAUACUAAACAGAUCAGGCAGACUUUUUCUUUUUCUUUUUUUUUAAAGAGAGAAUCAGUCCGCAGGUUGGCUGGAGUUCAGGGAUAAAACUCUUCUUAAGAGUGAAAUGGCAAGAAAGAUUCAGGCUCAUCGAGCACUGGGAAUUAGAUAGGAACAGAGACACCAAAAAAGCAAAAACUCAACUUAUAAUAGAACCAACAUCUGAUGCUACAGAGUAUGAAGAAAAACUGAGUUGGCAGUGAGAGCCAAGUGGUAGUACAGAAAAGCGUAUUAUAUUGCAAACCUAUAGAGAAUGUCAGGUAUUCUUCAGGGCUACCCUGUUCUGGACUUUUGACAUUCGUGGUAAACUGCCAGAAGGUCUUAGGGGAAUGGAGAAGUUGAUGCCAACCGUUCCAGUGCAUUCACUGUAGAAACUAUUGCUGGAGAUUAUGAUUGCCUUCUCCUCGAGAGACAAUGCUAAGGAUAUACUAGAAUCUUCUUGAGAAGUCCUACUCAACCAUCAGUAUGAUAUUUUGUCUUCUAAGACUAUUGGAUUUUUGUAUCUCCUUGCUUUAAGAUCUAAGUAAGAAUGUUUCAUUAGUCAUUGCUUACGUUUCUGGACUGUCUUCCAAUGCCCUGACUUUACAUAUCCUUUCCUCUUUUCUUCUCUCAAUAAAGCUGUGUACAUUACAAUUUUUUUUAUUAGGUGCAGAAAUCACUUGAAGAACUUAAAAUGCAAAUUUCUAGGCCCUAUGCCCAAAGUAUCUGAUUCAACUAAUCUGAUAUGGGGCCCCAGAAUAUGCAUUUUAACAAAAACUCCAGGUGAUUAUGGCACAGGUGGUCCAUGGACCACACUUUGGAAAGCACUGCUUUAAGUCAUCUAAAUGCCUUGGGAAGUUGACAAUUUACUAGCUGUAUUAUACCUCUCGGACUGUCUCUUGCAUCCCAUGUAGCACACAAAUCAUUCUUUUUCACACCAUAUCUUGAUUUGAAGCUCUGAAAAUGGUUCCAAUAACUGUAUCUUGCACCAAAACAUUGAGAAUUUUAGGUUCCAAUUUAUAAUUCAAGAUACAAUCAAUCUUGAAAACAAUCAUUUGUCUGUCUUUAGUUUUAUUGUCUCUAAGAUUUUAAGGGAAACUUAUUUUUAUUGAAAUUUACACUCAUUCUGAGAUAUGAAAAUGGUUUCAAUUUAUACCUGAAAUACAAGAUUAUAUCCUUUUGCUCUUCCCAGAGUAAAAAAUCUCUCCUUCACAUUUAUUAGAGAACUGUUCUUUCAACCACAAGCAUAAAGACAGACUCUUGGUAGGAGUUAAAAAGGACUAUUUGGGAUAUUUACAGUGUCUCUUUAGAACUGGAAGCUGGACAACAAGUAGUCAUCACAUAUGGGAAAGAUUUACAUUGCCUGAGUGGGCUCAAGUUUGAUGUAGUAUAAAUGGUAUUUUCAAAUGCUUAGUUCUCCAGAUUUUCCAUGGCUACAGUAUAUGCUCUUGUCUCUACUGAGAAAUAUGCUAGUCUAGGGAAUAUUGAAUAAGCAUUCUUCCAGGCAGUGUAGUCAUAGCCUUUUGUUUUCAGCCAAGUUUAGUGUGACUGUUUCACAUAUGAUUUUCCUCUUCAUGAACUACAUUGGAAAAAAUUAAAACCUUGUCUAAAAAUAAAUAUAUCAGGCUUUUACCCAUUAAUCAGUAAACAUUUAUUGUCACUAAGGUCUGUAAGAACUAAAUAGUAGGCUUAUGCAGCAGAUUGAGAAUCCAAUGCUAGUCAAAACCUGUUGUGUCCUUCCCCUUUUUAACCAAACAAAGAAAUAAAGAAUCACAGAAAGGGAAGAACUCCAUUAAAUGGCGUAUGAGGGCAGCUGCCUGAAAAAGUAGGUAGGGUUAGAACUAAAUGUCCAUAUUGUGGGCAUCUGCAUAGGCCUUUUAUAUUUUUGUUUUUCAGAAUGAACUUAUCAUCAAUGUGUUCAGUGUUAUAAAUUCUGAUACUAUAACAUAUUCAGAUUGAGCAAGAAGGCAUAUUUAACGGCAAAGAUAAGAGGUACAAACGUAAAAUAUUGCUCUCUACUAAGUGAUUAAGAUUUGAAAAGUGACACCAGGAAAGAAAUUGUAUGUGUUAAAAUACCAAGAUAGUUAUGAAAGGUAUUCACCAAAUAUUUCCACCUCUCUUCUCUCCAGGCACGAAAGAGAGUUAUAUCAAUUAUAUCUCUCCCCUCCUUUAAAGUUAGUCAUGGCCAGAUAACUUGCUUUGACCAAUGAAGAAUGAGCAGAAGUGAUGUGUCCCACUUCCAUGUAGAAGAUUUAGGUGCAAUGAUUGGGGUCAUCGUGUGCCCUUCCAAUGGCUAUGGGAUCAUGGAAGCACAUAUUGAGGUGCUUGAGUGACUAUGAUGAGCUAAGGACUCUGCUGACCCACAUUGGACUGGUAUAAGUCAGAAAUAAUCUUUGUUGUAGAACUGCUUGUUAGUGCAGCAUAAUUUAGCCUAUCUUGAGUAGUACAAAUGCGGACAUGGAGGCAAAAAAAAUUUCAAAUGUUUUGAUAGGAAAUGGGAAUUUCCCAAGUAAAGGUGGAGGUGGUCAGUAGUGUCCAGUUGUGCAUUGUGUAUCCUUUAAUGGAGCUCAAGAGCCAGCCUAAUGAAAAGAACUGUGCUUUUUAGUUAAAUUAUGUGGUCAGGUUUGAGUUACAAGGAAGCAAAAACGAUACUGAAAAAUUUGUGUUCUUGAAGAUGUAUAGUAGAGAGCAGAAAUAUACAACAAAACUGUCAAUGAUGACAUUUGAAUAUUGAUAAUGGGAACAAAUGGGGUGGCAAUUCUAAUUUGUCCUAACAAUCAGGCUUUUUUUUAAAUGAGCUUGAAGCAAUUUAGUAAUCAAUAAUACAAAUAUGGGAAAAUAUAAUGUCAUACUCCAAUAAAAAUCUAAACUUUUGACGGUUUUAAAAACUAUAUUUCAAAUAAAACAUGAUUGUCAGGAUUAAGAGAAUUCAGAAUAUACUGGUCCUGAAGAAACAUCCUAAAAUCAAGGCCAAGGAAGAAAAAUGGAGUAUCCCGUGUUACCAAUAUAAAAGCCAAGCCACACAUGUUCUACUCAUAGCACAAACUGCUUUAAAGAAACAUGGCUCAGUAACAAUAAAUAUUUUCUUUAAUCCAGUGAAGUUUCUUGGACUAUAUUAGAACAUGUUACAAUUCUGAAUUUAUUGCAAUAGCUCUUAAAAUUUUUUUCAUUUCUUGCAUUUGUCCUCAUAGCUUAUCUGAACCCUCAAAAAAAAAUGUUUCCCUGAAAUCCAGCCUAUGGACUCUCCUUUUCCUUUCUUAAAAAAACAUUUUUCUUACUUCAGGCAAUUUCUCUCCUUGAUUGUCUCAGCUCUCUCUACACACAUUUUCUCAGUUUGGCUUUAUUUUCUCAGGAAAUAUCUGAUCACAAAGAUCCAGUAUAGUUCCUGUUUUAGAAAUCUGAGAUCAUCAAGUUGAUUUAUUGUAGUACAGUUUGAAGCUCUGUCAGAUCUUAUUGUAAAGCACCACUGAAGAACAUCAACAAAUUGCACCCAUCAACUAAUACUUGGACUUGUUUUAACUCCCUGUCAUUAUUUAAUUAGGCUCAAAAAUGUCACUGUAUGCAGAGAAUCCAUUGUUUUUCAGUACUGAAGAAAUUCUUGUUGAAAUAGGGUAAUAUUUUUUCUGGCAUCAUAAAUUAAAGACAAUAAGAUAAAUAGAGAGUUGACAGAUAUAAGAGAAGCAAAGUUAGUUUCCAGUUAUAUAACACCAAUAAAUUUUUUAAAUGAAAUUUUGUGUUAGCAGGAGGUCAUAAAUGUUAAAGCACACACCAUUCACUACCCUCUACCUGUAGAAACAUGAAGUAGCAUGGAAUUUAUUGGCUUUAGGUUUGUCUAAAUAGUAAGCUUAAUGCACAUAUUUGAGUCUGAAGUAACUCUAAAAUGUAUAUUUCGAAAAACUCCAGUGAUAAUUCAAACGGCUCAUUUACGACAAGCUUUUGUGAUAAAGAAUCCUUAAAGAAACAAAGUUAAGCAUGUCUUUUGCUUCUAGAUCUUAAAAGAUUUUUUCUUAGAGAUGUCUGCUUUGAUUUCUGGCCAUGGUUUUGAAAUAGUGGGGCUGGUAAGUUACUAAGCUCCUAAAACAUAGCCUGAAAAAAAUGAAAACAGGGCAAGUAGAAAUUUCAAACCUUAUUUCCCACAGAAUAUUCAAAGAAUAGGAUAAUCCUGCCUGUUUUAGUUCUAUUUAUGGCAUCUGGCAAACUCUGUCAUCACAUUAUAUUUUUAAACAUGUCUUAAAAGUUUUAAAAUGAUGACCCUCAUUUUGUGUAUACUCUUUUUUUAAAAUCUCAGAUAAAAUAUGUGAGGGAAUGAGAUUAGAGUAUUUCCUGUCACAAAAAUAGAAUGUUCUUAUGUGUACAUAGAAAAGAAAAUAUAAGUAGUCCCUAAGUGUGUUUUCCUUCAUACUUAUCCACUGCUCAUGGCACACCACAUGUUGCCAAAAACACACACACAAGAAGCAGUGCCUUCUUUUUGAUUAUUUGUGAUUCAUUGUAAGCAUAAUAUAAGAAAAGGAAACAGCAAAAUUCUGGGGAUAUAAAUAGAACAGUUUUUAAGAGAAUUUACUAAGGCAUCACCUGAGAAGAAAGUUUUGUGAUUUAUUUAAGAGUAUGAAGCAGUGACUAAGAAGAGUUGUCAUACAACUUGCUAUUUUCUUUUGGGAACAGUAUUUCUCAUGCUCAGAGGAAAUGGCUUAAUCAAACAAUCCAAAUAUAUUAAUAUAUCAUAGAGAGGGAUAAAACUAUAUAUUCUGGAACUCUGAGGGACAAAAUUCUUUGUACUAUAUCUUUAUUUUUAACAGAAGGGUCUAUUUUCUAUUACCAUUUCUGCUAUUUGUAAGAGUAGUUUCCAACAGCCGAAUGGGGGCUGUGUAAAGCCAUUAUAAUGCAGUUUACAUCUGUCAAAAGGAUAUCUGAAUUCCAUUGAAAUACUAAAGUGGUAGAGUGAAACAGAGAUGUUAUAUGCCACUGAAGAUUAUUUUUCUAAAGUUUUCAGAACACUUUUUGUAAUAUUAUUAAGCCAGUGACAUGAUCAAUGAUGUGUACAAAGGGAGAAAGAAUACUUCCCAAAUAUAAUUGUAUACAAUGCUUUUUAAAUAUCCUUUCAUCUUCAAAGUGUUACUGCAUAUUCUUUUUUAUUUUUUUUCGAGACAGAGUCUCACCUUGACCCCCAGGCUGGAGUGCAGUGGCAUGAUCUUGGCUCACUGCAACCUCCGCUUCCUGGGUUCAAGAAAUUCUCCUCCCUCAGCCUCCCGAGUGGCCAGGAUUACAGGCAUGCGCCACCACACCUGGCUAAUGUUUGUAUUUUCAGUAGAGACAGGGUUUCGCCAUGUUGGCCAGGCUGGUCUUGAACUCCUGACCUCGUGAUCUGCCCACCUCUGCCUCCCAAAGUGCUAGGAUUACAGGGGAGAGCCACUGCACCCGACCUGCAAAUCCUUUUAUUUAAACAUUAGCUUCAACAUAUUUUAGACAAUUUCAAUUAUGUGACUUUUGAAUGAGUAACACUGAGCCUGCAGCCAUGCAGGCACUCUCUUUUCAUCUGCACUGGUUGGUGUGACAUUGUUCUGCAGCUGAUGAAAUAAAGGUCCACCCUCUUGUACCUCUUGGGUUAUCCCCCUUAAACAACAGCUUGAGAAGUAUAAUGACUGGGGAAAAGGAAUAAUGUUUACUCAGCAAAGAUCCUUUUCGGAAUUCGUAGAUAAUCUCCAGUGCCAAGGAAGUCCCUCCAGGAAAACAGAGGAAUAUUACCUCUCACCACCAUGCUUCUUCCAUUCCAUGUUACAGUAUUGCCUACUUCAACACUUUCAAAACUGGCAUCAGUCUCAGAACUGAUGUGUGCAUGGAUAUAGAAAUUUAUACAAAGUUCAUACAUAGGAAUUAAUGUUAUUCCUGAGGCAAGAAAAUACAGUAAUAAUCUAAUGGCCUUUUCUUCAUCAUUCUCUCUGUGUUGGCUCUAUUUUCUAUUCCCUUCCUUUUUCUCCCUCUGGAAUGCAAUAUGGUGUAUUGGUUGUAGAUUCCAGCAUAAUAGAGUUGACACCCUGCUUGUUUGGGUUUUUGUCAAUGGUUCUUUAAGUUUUAAAAUAUUAUUGAUCUGACUUUAGUGGCAAAUUCUACCUAGAAUAUUUUUCUUGUCAUUUUAAUUAUUUGGAAAUUUGUAGAUAAGUGACAAUUAUUAAAUACUCAUAUCCAAAUUAUGGGGGUCCUUCUUGUAUUUUGGCAAUCAGAAUCUGGAACAAGACUCUUUAUUUGUAUGUUAUUUUCUCACUUGGAUAGUAUCUUUGAGAGACCUUACAGAUUUUGUUAUUUUGUAAUUUUAACAUGACCACACAAUUUAUGUCUCUUCCUCAAAUAGGGGAGAUAUUUUCAGUUAAUGUAAUAUGGUAAAAAAAAAAUUAAGCUAAGAGCAAACACAAAAUAAUAAAAACACAAAGCCAAAACUAAAAGUAACUUGUAGUAUUUCUUUGCUUAAGGAUACACAGCUUAUUGUACUUGUAUCUUAUUAAUAUAUUAAAUCUUCCCUCACUCAUUCACACAUGCUCAACUUGACUCAUUCACACAUGUUAAUAUUGGAUAGUCUCUGGAUCAAUAUAGGUGCAUUAACUGCUUAAUGUUUGAUUGCAUUGAUUCACCAUCACAGAGUUCCCAGAAUUCCCUGGAAGAAGGGCUGUUCCCUGGAUGUGGGAAGGUAUGCUGCAUGAAACAUGUCCCUCAUAAUAUUAGGUUGGUGCAAAAGUUAUCACAGUUUUUGCCAUUAAAAGUAAUAGUAAAAACCGUGAUUACUUUUGCACCAACCUAUACAUUCUUGUAUCAGAGUUGUGAAAUUUACCCACAGUUUAGUUUUAUACCUACUACACACACACACACACUCACACACACAUAUAUACAAUUUAGAGAAAAUUCCAAGUUAUCAUUAUAAUAUUAUUCCUAAGUAGCUGAGAAAAAAGUUUGCUAGAAUUUGAAUUUUUGUUAACAGUGUUUGAAUAUCAAGUCUAUCUUUAAAAAAUAUGGGGCUUUCUAAAAUAAUUUUCUCUACAUUAGCCUUCCUAUUAAUUUAAUGCAUCUCAGUUGUAUCAGAACUUUUCUAGUUCUAGUUACAAAAACUCAACUCAAGCCAACAUCAGCAAAAAAAUGGAAUUUAUUAGAACAUAAAAUUGAGAAGUCCAAGGGAAGAUCAGCCUUCAGGCAUGGCGUAUCAAUCUGGGUCCAAUCAGGAGAGAGAAACCGCAUAGUAAUUUGAACAGGGACAGUUUAAUAUAAAGAAUGAUUAACUAUUACAGGGAAUUAGAGUAUGCAGGGAUUGGCUAAUAAGUAAAAAGUACUCUAAAGAAUAUAAGAAUAGCAGAUCUAAGGAGCAGCCACUACUUCUGUCGGGGGGAAUUGAGCACCCAAGGAAAAGCUCAUACCCGAGGCUGAGAUCCAGAGCUCUCUGGAGACGCUAUGGCCUUGACUCACUAGACCUCACGGUGGUGCUGUGCCCAUAGAAUUUUCUGCCAAGUCCUCCUUCAUUUCAUGCUUGAAAUUAGCCCUCCAGAGUGCCAGAAAAAUUCAUGUGGAGGUAUCUCACUAGAGGACUCUGCUACGAAACUGCUUUGUGAGGAGGGACUGCAGAAGCUGGGCACUGAGGAAGGUGUGUACACUGGAGGGGCUGGGUGCUGGAGAAGCUGCCUGUGCUGCAGGAGCCUGCGGAGCCAGCAUACAGGCUCUAGGAAGCAAAAUCCCAUUUUCUUCUGCAGUGUCUCUCUAUCGCCCUCUACUGAUGAUAGAGUUUAGCAUGGUAGCAGCUGGGAAAGGAAAAAAAAUUUUUUUUGUUUUUUUUUUUGUUUUUGUUUUUGUUUUUUGAGAUGAGUCUUGCUCUGUUGCCCAGGCUGGAGUGCAGUGGCGCAAUCUCGGCUCACUGCAAGCUCCGCCUCCCGGGUUCACGCCAUUCUCCUGCCUCAGCCUCCCCAGCAGCUGGGACUACAGGCGCCCGCCACCACGCCCAGCUAAUUUUUUUGUAUUUUUAGUAGAGACAGGAUUUCACCGUGUUAGCCAGGAUGGUCUCAAUCUCCUGACCUUGUGAUCCACCCGCCUCGGCCUCCCAAAGUGCUGGGAUUACAGGCGUGAGCCACUGCGCCCGGCCGGCAAAGGAAACAUUUUUAAAGGGACAUAUCCAUUUUCACAGAGCAGGCAAAAGGAUUAAUUUAUAGCUAAGGUGGACUGAUCUAAAUAUUCAAAUGAUGUUAGCAGGAUUUGCUUUUUCUCCAUUUCUCAGCAUUGCUUUCUUCUGGGUAGUUUCAUUCUAGGCUGGCUGCCUCCAUAUUAUGGUAUGAAGAAUUCAGCAGAACAAAAUUUCUCUUCUUGUCAAUUGUCACAAAAAUCCCAGAAGUUAGUAUGUUGACUCUAAUUAGCCUGAAUUGUGCCACAUGGCAUCCCCAAAGCCAGAAGAUGUGUUAUUAUUUUUGACCUCAUUAGAUAUUAUGCUUUCCCAACCCUGCCCUCCUCAGAAUGCCAUUAUCAGACUAAAGUAAUUAUUUCGGAGGGGAAAGGAGGGGGGCAAAACAACCUUGAAUAAAUAGAGACACAAUAUCUGAAGAGCAAAACUACAGAAUUUACUGCAUGCCUUAAAUGCCUUAUAUCCUGUUGGGCUUUAUUUUUAAAAUCAUUUUACAAGGUUCUAGAUCAUAAAAGGAAAUUAAAGUCAUCCAGCUUAGUCAAAUCCCUUGAGUUUACUACUAAAAAAGGAAAUUCAAUGUUUGUGGUUUCAAACCUAGAAUUUCUGUUAAAACUGAAUCAAAAAGUUGCAAGAUAUAACUUCUUUUUUAAUGAUGAGGGGCCCCAUCUACUUAACUAAACAUAUUCCCCGAGCAAUAGUGGUAUGCCUGUGUCAUCUGAUAUAACUCAACAAUUUGGAUGGAACCCAAGGCAUUAUGCUCAGUGAAAAGCAUAUCUCAAAUGGCAACCUACAGAAUGAUUACAUUUCAUAUAAAAUUCUUAGAAAUGGCAGAAUUAUAGUGAUGGAGAACUAAUCUGUGAGUGCCAAGAGUUGGGACUGGGGAGAGAGUGUGACUAUAAAGGAGCAAGAAGGAGCUUUUUGGAGUGAUCAGACAGUUGUGUGUCCUGAUUACCAUAGUGGUUUCACAAAUCAAUAUGUAUGACAAAAUUCCACAGGACUGUACACCUCCCCACAAUGCAAAAAACAUGAGUGCAUGUAAAAACUUGCAAAACUCCAAUAAGGUCUGAGUUUAGUUAAUAGUAUUGUGCAAGUGUGAAUUAUGUAAUACUGGUUUUGCUCAUUUUACUAUAGUUUCCAAAGAUGUUAUCUGUAGGGGAAGCUACCGAAGUUACAGAAUAAAUUUUUGUACUAUUUUUGCAACUUCUAAAUGAGGGUAAAAUUAUUUCAAAAUAAAGUUGGCAAAAAUGAUAGUUAAAAAUUGUAGCAAAUUGAGGGAGAUUUUCUGGUAAGAAUCGGGAAACAAAGUUCUUUUUAAUUUUUUGAUUUUUUCAUAGCAAACAAAAAAGUAUUAAUAAUUAGCUUGGAUAUAGAAGAAAUAAAAUGGGUGCUUACACUAUUCUAAAAAUGAAAGAUAUUUUAAUAAUAUUAGGCUUUAAAAGCAAAGAAAACAAUUACAAAAAUGCAUGCAAAUAAAGAGGACAGAAAAUUAGAAAAUUAGUAUGAACCACCCUAUGGUACUGAAGUCAGAGAUAUUAACAUGGAAUAAUUUUUUAAAAUAUAUGCUGAGAAUUGUAUGUGUGCACAUGAAUUAGCAUAACAUGCAUAUAUUUCCUAGCUGUAUACACUGAGAGAGGCUGCAAAGUGUGAGGCCCCAGUAACAGUGAGCACACUUAAUGUCCAGAUUUUGGUUUCUAAACAUCAUCUUUCAAAAAACAAUAACUAGAAUGCCUUGGAGAGUUCAUUGAUUCCAGGGCAGGUGCAGAGAAUCUGGGACACCUUGUGUACCAGAUUUUAAGGAUUUGCUAAGAAAAAAAAACAAAAAACAAAAACAGUGGCAUAUUGAAAGGGCCCACUAACCAACUUGAAAGAGCUUCUAAUGUUCAAAGUGGGAAUAAUUUGAGCAAGGAAAGAAAGAUAGUAUCAGAUUAUAACCCAAGGACUAUGAUAAAAUUACAUGAGUCUAUACUAAUAGAAAUAAAUUACUGAAAAAUUUUAAAUGAGGUAGAAGUGAAUAUUCUUUCUUAUAGAAAAUUCCAAAUCACAAAUAUCCAAAGAAUAAGGAAUAUAGAAAUCACUCUAAAAAUAAUAAUUGCUACAGGAAAAUCUAUCUAUGAAUGCUAAAAUUGGUGGGCAUAAUUUGAAGUGGAACCAGUAAAUUUGCAUAGACUCCAAGUAUCUCUUUUCAAAUAUUUAAUAACUAUAAAGAGAAAGAUGCAGCUUUUAAUGCAGAAUCCUGGCAGCAUCACUUAGCCAAGUGAUCAAAGUUAAUACUACUGGUAAUAUACUGAUAUCACGUGCCUCUUGAGUGACCUACUGAGAGGUCACAUCCUCUCUGUGUCAUCAUUUCUAAUAAUGUGUAACCUCAAUCUGAUGAUGAGAAAACAUCAGACAAACUCAAAUUCAGGGGCAGUCUACAAAAUCACAGACUAGUCAUCUUCAAAAAUGUCAAAGUCAUAAAUGGCAAAGACAGGAAUUGUCACAGAUUGGAGAAGACUAAAGAGACAUAAAAACUAAAUGCAGCAUGAGAUCUUCAAUUGGAUCCAGGAACAUGACAAGUAAAAAGCUGGUGAAAGCAAAGUAAUCUCUGUAGUGUAGUUUAUAAUACUGUACCAAAAUUAAUUGCUUAAUUUGGAUAAUUGUAUCAAGGAUAUGUGAGAUAUUAACACAAGAUAAAGCUGGGUGAAGAGUAUACAGGAACUCUAUUAUAUUACCUUUGCAACUCUUCUCUAAGUCUAAAAUUAUUUCAAAAUUUGUAAAGCUUAAAGAGAAAAAUGUUUCCCAGGUUAUUGUGACAAUGAAUCGGGCUUGAGAAUCACUGUGCUGAUGAUUGGUGACUGAGUUUCCUCCAGCUCUUUGCUCUUGUACCAGAGAGUAGAAUUGCUCAGAUAGAGCAAAGCAGAAAAUAGGUCCCAGGCUGAAUGAAAUAGGGCCCAAAUGGUAAAAUAGCAAAAUCUUAAACCAUUGCUGGACAUAAGGUAGGAAUUAAGAAGAAGAACAGGAGGAGGAAAAGGAGGAAGAAGAGGAGAGAGGGGGAAGGGAAGGAAGAGGAAGAAGAAAAGGGAGAGAAGGAAAGGAGGAAGAGAAAGAAGAAAAAAGAGGAGGAGGAAAAUAUGCUCAAAGAAACUUCUGAAUAAAACUUAAUUAUUAGAAUACAAAUCUUAUUUCAUUAAGCCAUAUCAAAAGGCUGGAACAAUUUCUGCUGCAUAGCAACUGAAACAGUCUACAUUGAAACAAUGCUUAUAACCAUGUGGCCCUCUGCUAAAUGCUGGGAAUUUUAAAAAUGUUAAUGUUUGCCUUAUAUAUUAUUCAAGAACAUUUUAGCACAAGUAGUUUAUUUCCUAGAUAUUCAUAAGAUAAAUAUAUGCAGCUUGCAUACUAUUUUCAGUUGAAAGUUCUCAAUAGGAGAAAAAGAUCAUUCAUAUUAAGAAAUCAUUCAAAUUAAAGCGUCCUUUUUUAAGUUAAAUACAUAAAAACACAAAACGUUUUUAGUUAAAUACAUAAAAACACAAAGCUUGGUACGGCUCUAAGAUGAACACAACAUAUGCCUCAAAUGUGAACUAUGGAUGGUUAUGUCUCAGUUAUUAAUAGUCAUUUUAAACUAUCUAUAGUUUUAUAUUUUUUAUCCUUUUUUUGUUCAAGUAUAGCAAUUUUAAAGUGCAUUAAAAAUAACAGUAUAAUUAGGUGAUAAAUUUGCUAAACCUAUAUCCUACUUUUUACUCAGAUUCUCCUAUUAUAAUGCCCACCAGAUUAGUAGAAGGGUCUGUGCCCUACAAAUAGUGCUUUAUGUUGUAUGAUUAGGAAAUAUUAAAUGAAAAAUAUUGAUAACUAUAUUUCAAGUGUGGUCUAAGUCUAAAUUAGGUAAAAGCCUGGGAAAAGUUAUCAAGUCUUGCUGUACUUACUUAAAUAUUAUAUAACAUUUUUCAUAUACUUGUAAUAUGAUAUAAGGCUUCUCUUCCAUAUGGUUGGUCAGUUGCUCUGCUACAGGAAUUUUCUUUCCAAGUAAAAAUUGAAAUAUGUAUAUUUACAGUGUCAUCCCUUGGGCAUAUGUAUAGAUGGUGUCUUAUGAGAUUCCCUAAGUAAAAUAGGAGUAACUGAAGUGGAUUGCUGAGACUGUUACAUUUCUCUGUACUUUAGAAAUCAUAUGAAAAUUAUAUAACUGUUCCCUGUAGAUCAAACCAUGUGCUUGUGUAGGCAGCAGCUACUUAUUCCAACAAAACACGGCUUGUGAUCCCCCUUGGGAAGUGAGCCGGCCAUCUCAGGCAGGCAUUCCUUCCCUGGCAAUAUGUUAGCCAGACAUGGUGAACCCAUUAUUAAUGCAUCCAUGUAUGAUAGGUGUAUUUACAUUAUUCAAGCUCAAGAGAAUGAUGGAGAAGACCACAGCUCUAGCACCAUUUUUAUUUGGGCUGGAUUACUUUCAUCAAUAAAAUGGUAUUUCUCCAUGAAAUUAAGAUACAUACAAAGCCAAAUGACAUUUGAAAGAUGACUUGGUGAACCUGGACUCUGAAGAAUGUGCCGUGUAUGUAACAAGUUUUUAAUAAUUCAACUAAGCUAUUUUAUAAUGAAGUGAAUGUCACAGAAGAUGGAAAUCAAUAAAAUUCAUUAACUAGGGCCCCUUCAUGGAUAAUGUUUGGAUAAGAAUUAAUAGCACUGGCUUCUUGAUUUCCCAAUAUGACCACCAGUUGCUAUGUAGCGCUAACCAAACGACUUUACCUCUCAUAAUCUCGUAUCCAACUCCAAAGUUUACUGUGAUGAUUAAGAUAAUAUUUAUAUGACCCACCUAUAUAAAAAUUUCUCAAUGAAGAUAGCACCCUCCAUAUUCACUGCCUACUUCUGUUUUAAUGCCAGAAAGAGUUUUGAGCUAUGAAAUAACUCAUGUCUACCUAACUGUGCUGCACUGAAAGCAGAACACUUGUGACUCAACUGAAGAGUUAGGCUUAAGAGCUGAACUAGCACAUGUUCAGAGAAGGAGAUAAUUUAUAAUGAUGGAUAAAGAAUAAUAAUACUUGCUGGAUAUGGUGGCUCACGCCUGUAAUCCUAGCACUUUGGGAGACCAAGGCGGGUGGAUCACCCGAGGUCGGGAGUUCCAUACCAGCCUAACCAACAUGGAGAAACCUCAUCUCUUCUAAAAAUACAAAAUUAGCAGGGUCUGGUAGCACAUGCCUGUAAUCCCCGCUACUCGGGAGGCUGAGGCAGGAGAAUCGCUUGAACCCAGGAGGCGGAGGUUGUGGUGAGCUGAGACCGCACCAUUGCACUCCAACCUGGGCAACAAGAGCAAAACUCCGUCUCAAAAACGAACAAACAAACAAAAAACCGAAACUUUAGUUAUAAAGGAAAAGAAUUGAGACUAUCAGAUUUAAAGUAGUUAAUAUCCAGUUUGAAAAAUAAUUUGUAUGGUAAGUCGAGGUAGUUUCAGGCAGCACAUUGGAAUAAAAAGGAUAAAGGGGUUGUGAGCUAGAUGGACUUGCUUUGCAAUUUCCAACUCUUUAGCACAGCCUGAGGAAGUCAUUUAGUAUCCAUGAAUUUCUGUUUUCACAUUUGCAAAACAAUAAUAAUUAUAAAAAUAAUUGAUGAAGCUAAAAACAAAUGAUAUAUUAAGGUAUAUAAAUUGUCUGGCACACAGUAGGAGUUCAACAUGUAGUCCUUAACAUUAUACUUUGUGGUUGUAUUCAUGUGAACUUCAGAAUACCAAAAUAUUACAUUGGGUCUGGCUUUUGUGCCUUACUGAGGCCCAUGUGUGAGAACAAAGACAGUCACAGUCACCUCCUAUACCAAUUGAGGUUUCAGUGUAUUACAGUUUUCUGAAUCUUAGAAAAUACAUUGCUGUAGAAGACUGCUUAGUGCUAGUAAUAUUGUUCUUAACUAAAUUAGAGCUUAAUUCAUUUGCUGUCUAAGAUGGAUCCCUUCCAGGGCGUCUUCCCUAUUACUGGAAUGAAGAGGAAGAAGGGACAGCGUAACACUUUCAUGCCUACAGCUUGAGAACAAUUUUUAUACCUUCAUCAUGAUGCUCAUUUUGCUAUUCCUUUCUUUAACUCUUUGUAUUUGUAUCUAUUUCCUUAUGUUUUAUGGGCCUGAAGCUUAAUUUGCCUCAAAAUCUUUUAAAAUAUUGAGAUUCUUCUGUUUCUAAAAUUUAUAGCCACAAUAUCCCUUGUGCCAUUUGCCCAGGUUAAUUAGUUAGGGGGCAGUUCACACCUUCUUUUCCAUGUGAUUUACAGGGCAGUUCACACCUUUUUCUGUGUGAUCCCCAUUGUGGGAUUUACAGAAUGUGGCUUUGCAAACAGUGUGCCAUGGAUCUUUGCAUAUUCUUAUUAGAGUCAGAGGCUCCUAAUGGUUCUGAAACAUAUUUUCCUUCAUAAUAAAUUUCAAACACUUCGUUUCCAGUGCCAGGAAGAUUGGAAUUUUUAUAUUUUUUUAUAAAUGGACAAAUUCUUUUUUUUUUCUUUUUCUUUUUCUUUUUUUUUUUCCUCGAGAUGAAGUCUUGCUCUGUCACCCAGGCUGGAGUGCAAUGGCACAAUCUUGGGUCACUGCACCCUCCGCCUCCUGGGUUCAAGGUACACUCCUGCUUCAGCCUCCUGAGUAGCUGGGCUUACAGGUGUGUGGCUAACCUUUUGUAUUGACAAAUUCCUUAAAUAGCGUUUUAUAGAAUGGGAUUGCAGAUACAAUUAGAUUUAGGAAAAUCUCCAAAAUUUUGUACAACUCAUUAUAAUGAGCAGUAUAAUGAACAUUGUGAUAAAAAAGCUUGGACCAACUAGAGGUCUAAUUGUCCUUUGACCCAAUAACUUAGUGAAUGAUACAGUGUUUCUUUGCAGCAGCUCUUCAUCAUCUUUACAACAGGUACUGUACUUGGAUCAUCAGUAGUUGUAAUAGUUGCAAUAAACUUAUACUAAAAUAUAAUAUACUAUGUAAAUUUAGAUAUAAAAUGCUACAUAAAACAAGAUUUUUAUGAAUCAUUAAAAUAUACAUUGUUAACUGAAAGGAGGUCAUUUUCUUCUCUUUAAGAGAGCUAGGUAAUACUACCAAACAGUAUAUAAAUGAGCAUGGCUUAUUUAAAGAAAAUACAGUGGAGCAGGCAGCUCAGAAACAUAAAUCCAAUUACUAAGUCAGAUAAGAAUUUUGUCAUCAUUUUACAGGAUAUCACAAACUGAUGAAUUUCUGAGAGACCUCAAUCAAUUAAUUUUUAAAAGAUGUUGGAUUUGUACAGGGCUUUAUAUUUUUCAAAAUAUUUUAUUUUAUUUGAAUGUAAGCUUUCUAUUCUAACCCUUUCCUGGGUUUUUCUCUUGAAGACAUUAGCUGUACACUCAGAAUGUACAGCAUUCUGAAACUGUCAAAGAACAGACAAUAUUCCAGUAUACACAAAACUUCCCAUCUGCAAUUUUUAGUUCAAAGACCCAUGGAGCUUUGGAGGUGGGAUAAUGUACCCACCAUAGCUUUUGUUGCUUUUUGUGUUAGUCAAUGGCUUCUAUUUCUCUUUCCUUUAAUCUCUAGUUAUAUUAGGUACCAUCUUAGUUGCAGAUACAUGCGGACAAAACAAGAACAAAGGUAUGAGAUAAAAGUUUAUUUGAGCUACAAGUUUAUAGCAAAUACGAAUGCAAGUUGAUUAGGGAGCCUGUGGUGAGACUUAUAGGGAGAGUCUCAUAAAAAUAUAUCAUCUUGAUACUUUCGUCUUUGAAACUGUGCUAGAAUGCCUUCAUUACCGAUUAUUCCUUUCAAUAUUGAUGACUUUGACCAAUAAUCUCACUGUUUCCCGCCUCCCAACACCACCCAUUCCCCUUGCGUCCUUUCGAAAAGCACUAAAGGCAAAGGUGAUAUUUAGGUCCUCUAAGAGUCAAUGUGGGUGAAAAUGAAAUACUUCUUCAGAGCACAGUCAGGAUGAUUACCCAGCCGCUUUGAUAAAUUUACCGACAUCUGUUACAGAGUCAUUUCUGCUGCACAAAUCUGCCAUUAACAAACAGUAAGGACUUUAAUUAACUGAAGAUACCAAGGAGUGAUACUCUGAUAAAAUGGCACCAUCUGGAAAGAAAGAUGUAAAAUUUUCUCCUCAGCUGUGUUGAUUGGGGAUUAUAUUAAAAUGUGUCUUGAUCACAAAUGAUUCCCCUGCUGUUGUAGGGUUCUUUAUUAGUAGCAUACUAGCAAAGGCUUUAUGGCUUGAAAUACUUUGCUCAGGUGUGCCGCAGCAUUAAAAUGUAAAUUUUCUGAACUUCGGAUUUUUCCUUUGGCCUUUCGUUGAUGCCCCAUUAGUGCUCAUUAACUUUUCCUGCUCCACAAAGAAUGAUGUUGAUCAACUUUGAGCUUCAAGAAGAGGUCAGCCAGAACCUAGCAGUGCCUAAACCCUUGGCAAUUGUUCUUAACAAGCCUAUUUGGAAAUUUAAUGUAAAUCAGGAUCGUCUCUCUAGAAGAAUGCACAUGUGUACAUAAUCACAGAAUUUUGGAUAUGAUUUCAGGGCCUCCUAGACUCUCAGGAGGCAUGCAUCCCAGGUUAAGUAUCUCUUCUUCAGACAUACUUAUUUGUCUCUCUCAUACAUACAGCAUUACAUUCCUUCUGGCAGCCUACCCCAUUCAGCUGCUUCAUUUGACCAGAUUUUCAAAGCUUUUCAGGAAACAUGAACUUUGAGUUUAGAAAACUAAACUUGUUCCAAUUUGGUUCAGUCUGAUGGGUCCCAAUUGAGUAUUUUUACCCCUGACCUCAAAGAGUGAUAAAUUAAAUCAGUUGCAAGUCGUUAAGUCUUGGCUUCCACUCAUCUAAGGUCUAAAGGGGAAGAAGGGAUGCUUGAACUGGAUUCUAAGGGGAGGUACAUCUAGAGGACUCUAUCACAAGCUUCUUAGCAAGGAAGCAAUGCUUGCUACCAUUUAAGUUCACAGAAGCUUAGUUAGUAUAAUUAAUUGUUGAAAAUAUGUAUAAUUGUUGAAAAUAUGCUGUUUGGCAAUAAUGUGUGACCAUCAUGAAUUACAUGGCCUAAAAUUACACAUUCUACUUCUAAGGGCAUUUGAGAGAAGGCUUUAGAAAGCAGUCUGCACAUGCUAGAAGAACAUGACACCCUCCCAUGGGUAGCAGUUGUUCCCUAUGACAUAUUUUUUUAAUUGGGGGCUGGAUUGGGAACUCAACAAGAGAAUGUUGCUAUAUAAUCCACUGUGAUCUGAAAAAACAUGCACAAAAAUGGGAGUUAAGAAAUAAAGAUGUUCACCAGCUCAAUUGUUGAAUAAUUAUUAUUUUCAUAAGUUCACUUGGGUAAUCUCUAGUUCCAGUUUUCCAUUUCUAAGAAGAGAAUGCUAAUGUAACUCGGAAAUUAGGUAAUUAAGAGAAAGCUUAUGACUGCCCAAAAAUAUGUAGCUUUUGCUACAUAUGGCUUUUUCCCAAUUUUAUUUACAUCAGUCUGAAUAAAGCCUUGCAUUUAUCAAGUGGCAGAAAAGACAUACAUAAUACACUUUUUAACUUAACAAAAGACCUAUAUUAUGCUGUUCUAAAAUAAUUUUAUUUACCUUUUUAACCAAAUCAAAGGCACCCAAUGCCACAAAGAUAUUUUCAGCUAAUGCUAGUGUCUUCAAGUCAGAGAGCAUUUGUAAAAUUGUGUAUUUUUAACAGUAUAAUUUUUUUCUUUUUUAAUUAAUUUUUUAAAACUAUUAUUAUACUUUAAGUUCUGAGAUAGAUGUGCAGAACGUGCAGGUGUGUUACAUAGGUAUACACAUGCCAUGGUGGUUUGCUGCACCCAUCAACCAGUCAUCUACAUUAGGUAUUUCUCCUAAUGCCAUCCCUCCCCUAACCUCCCCACCCCCAACAGACCCCAGUGUGUGAUGUUCCCCUCCCUGUGUCCAUGUGUUCUCAUUGUUCAACUCCCACUUAUGAGUGAGAACAUGUGGUAUUUGGUUUUCUGUUCUUGUGUUAGUUUGCUGAGAAUGAUGGUUUCAGUAUAAUUUUUAUCCCACUCCUGAUACAGUGCCAAACAACCUAUUGUUUUUCUAAUUAUCUUAAAUCAGACUCUGAAAUCCAAGUCACCAGGAUGUUGAAUAAAUAAAGCUUCAAUCAUACCCAUUAUUGUCUUUCCUUGCCUUAUUUUUCCACCCUGGGAACUAGGGUUGUGUUAAAAUUUCAUAGAGAGGAUUCUCAGGUCUUCAACUCACACUUGGCUGAAAUGAUUAAUGUCCAAGCCACAUACUAUCCUGAUGACGGAUGGUUUUGUUGCCUCUGUGCCAAGACCACUAGGGUAUUUGGGCCUACAUCCAACCUUGGAGCCCAGAGGCGCAGGGGCUGACCUCAGAAUUGUACCAAGCCACCAUUCUCCUCCACAUCCUGUAACCUCCCAGGGGCAUUUCAAGCACCGCUAUUCCAAGGUCCUGCCAAAGCUUCCAUGACUUGCUAGUCUUGGAGAGUAUGUUUUCUUACCCUGAUGUCAGCAACUUUGCUCUGUAUCCCUCAAGGCACUUUUUUUAUUUUUGUCUCCCCCUGUAUCCCAAAUAAAUUCACCCUCCCUGAGCCUUUAUAAAUACAGUGUUGAGGUGUCUUUCUUGAGAGUUUUUUAUUACUAAUUCACUCUAAUACAUGUUUUUAUUUGCUUGCUCUGACAGUUUUACAUAGUUGUCGGUUGCUUCUUGUAAUGAAAGAGACCAGAUGUUUCAGCAUUCUCAUUUUAUUUUUCUCCCAAUUCGAAAAAAAUAUGCUUUUUAUUUCAUUGUGACCCUUUUGAGAAAAUUCUGUAGCAGGCAUCAAUAUAAAGCAAGAUUCUCAAUGUUAAGUCCUAGGGAUUAUAAGCAGGCAUUUUCAGACCUUGGCAUUCUAACGUACUAUCUAGAGAGAUGUUAACUUACUUUUCAACUCCCAGCAGCAUUGUUUUGUAAAUUAUCUUCCUUUCAACUGCUCUAAACACUUUGCCACUUUAACCUUUUUUUUCUUUUUGGUUCAUUGUAAAUCCUUCAUUUAUUUACAUCUUAUUCUUUUCAAUAUUCCUUCACUUGCUUUAGGCAAAUGUGUUUUGAGUUUCUUCAGAUUAAGAAAGAAUUAUGCUAUCAGUUGCCGGUGUUCCUUAGCCUGUCCCAGGGAGGGGUGGUCUGCAAGGUGGAUUUCCACACAUUCUACAGUAUUACCUCCACUCUAUCUCCUCUCUGACUUGACUCUUAAUAUUGUAUUCCAAAAAACUAUAGAGAGAAGGAAGAUCAAGAUAAAUUAUCCAGAGUCUAGAAUUAAAGAAAGUUGGUCCUGGUGUAGCAGCUCCUUCUCAGUCCUGUUUUGAGCUUUUUGACUGAUUGCUUUCAUUCCUGUUCUGCCAUCUCAGUGUCCAUAUGGAAGUGAUUGUUUGCUUUAAUUAUAAAAGAAAAUAACCCAAAAGAAAUAGCAACUAAGUAAAACAGCAAAAAAAAAAGUUUUCUUUGAUGAGAGAAGGUAGGUGAUUUAAAAGAUUAGUCUAUCAGCAGAAAACAAGCUCUGUGUUACAUAUGAACUGGGGACUAUGUCUUCCUAGAAGUUAUAAAAAGGAUCAUUACAGAAUUGUUUACACAAUUCCUCCCACCUUUCAUCCAAUUUAAAGUAAGUACCUGUCAUAAGCAUUGCAUAGAAAAUCAUUACUCACACCUGUUAAAGUUUUAGGUAAACAAGGGGAGAUACCAGCCUCAGGGUCAACUGGUCUAGGAUAGAAGGGCUUUCUAUUAAUACAAACACAAACAAGAUCAAAGACAUUUUUUUCUCUAGUCAUCACUAUAAACAUUGAUUGACAUAUAUCUAGCCACCAUUUUCAACAUUCUUAACAUUUUGGGGGUUUUUAUAUUAUGUACUAAAAUGAGUGCAAAUUAAAAAACAAGUGAACUCUUCCAUUUAAAUAGAUGGAGAAUAAAUAUAUUAUUGUAAAAAUUAAGAAAAGAAAUAUACAUACCCAUCUGGUUAUAUAUUCAUAUUUCAAGGUGUUAAUGGCAGAGUCAGCAAAUGAAUUAUUCAUAUGGUUAAUCAAGUAAGUAUUGAAAUAAGAGAGAGAAUUACCUUAUUCCAUUCAAGGCAUAGACACUUCCAAAAUGUUAUAAUAUAACGGAAUAUAUUAAUGCCUAUAAAAGUUUAUUUAACAUUAGUUAGCACCCACUCUUUUUUUCAGAUAUAGAACCUACUUCAGGACCUUCAAUGCUUAGUUCUAACAUCCUUUAUUGUUUUGUAAAAUUUCUGGCUCACAGAGCAUUCCAGUGAGGCAACCUCAGAAGGUAAAUAAGCCCCUCAUUUUGGACAUCAUAAGGCUUUUCAGAUCAGAGGAGCAAUGCAUGGUGAAAGGGUAUUAGCCAUGCAGGCUGAGGGGUAGAUGUCCAGGACAGACUGCAAGAAGCAGGAAAUGUGUGUGCCUAAUUAAGGGAUUUCUCCUUCUGUCAUUUCCCUAUAAUCUACUGCUAGCAUGGAAAUAUAAACUGGGGUCUUCCAAAGGUAUAUUUGAAAGCACAUGGUCUUUGGAGUCAAAUCCUGAUUUAUAACCUACCCAGCAUGUAAUUGAGGGCAAGUCACUUAAAAUUUUUUGAGACUCAAUUUCCUCAUUUGUAACAUAUUAUGAAAUCAUAAAAUUGGAUAACAUGAGAGUCUAUCUUUCAAGGCUGUCGAGAGGAUAAUAAAAAUGUAUUCAAAGUCCUCAGAACGUGAUCAAUGCUUAAUAAAUGCUAGAUGUUACACAAGCUUUCUUUUUAAAAAUUUCAGCCUUGCCUUUCAUGUAAGUCAAUUACCAACUUUGUUAGACAAUAUCUUCUUCAUCUUUAAUUUUCAGCUCAAAAUAGCCAUGUAACUUUGAGAAAUGUCCUUAACCUUUAUAUGAUUCUAUUUCUUCACAUGUGAAAUAACAGGAAUAAUAUCCUGAGUAAGGAUAGUGCUCUGCAAGGCCAUGUCCUAAUAGGAUGCUAUCCAUUUUGUCCUUGAUCACAAUUAAAGCAAAGUACAGGCAUAUGCAUCAACGUGCUUCAUAGUGCAGAAUAGUGCCGUUGUCAGAUGCGUGGAUUCUGGGGCCAGACAACCUACAUUACUACUCACAGUUCAUCCACUCAACAUGGCUGAGUGAUCUUGGGCAGGUCAUUUAGCUGUUUUAUGCCCCAGUUUCUUACUUUUCUAGACUCCCUUUAUACCAUUUAAUUUUCCAAUGGCAUUAUACAGAAAAUCUUUUGUCCUCAAAUGUCUCAUCUAUUCUAGUGGUACUGCACUCUUCACAUGUAGUAAAUAGUUUUAAUGAAAACAUUAGAUUGUUUUACCAAAAGCUAGCUAAACAUCAGCAUUUUAUCCUCUGAACCCAAUCAAAUUAAAAAAAAGUUUCUUCAGUGUCACUUCUUUUUGUUUGUAGAGAUAUAAAAUUAUUAUAACACAUGUUGACUAGAAAUUUGGGACAUUGUCACAAACAAUUUAUUAAUGUUAUUAAUUUUAUUAAAACAGAGAAGAUAGUAUGAAAGCAACAUGUCCAUUAAUCAAAACACCCUCCAUGUUUACUUGGUAGUUGUACUUUUCAUGAGUGAACCUGAUGGCUCAUGACCUGUAAUGCCUAUACAAACAUUUCCACAUUUAUGAAAGGUUUGGAAGAGCUCUCUUUCAAUGUUAAGGCUCAACUAUAGUUAACAGAAAAAAAAUGUAAUUCUAUCAAUAUUUUUAACUUAAUGACAAGAUAGGGAUUUGAACUACAUGGCUACUAGCAGCUUUUCUAAUGCAAGAGCCAAUGAUUUCUGUGUGUCUCUUGAGAAGUUUAUUUAAAAAUGGCAGCAUUUGAAAUUACCUCUAGAGAUGUGACUAAUGUGAGUCUAAAGGUUUUGUCUUAAGAUGUUGAAUUCCUAUAAAAUAUUUUAAAUACAAAGAUUAAAAUGAUGCAAAUUUUAAAGCUUCCCUUCUCUUUAGUAAAUGUUUGCUCACUAUUCCUCACCCCAGGUAUGAGUUCACUCCAGAACUUGAAUCCAGUUGCUAGUGAAUAUGGAUGGAAAGAGAGUUCUAGUCUAGGGUAGUGAGCUGCCCAGCCCAGGAGAAACUUAAUAUGCAAGGGGAGCUCACGGAUACCUCCCACCUCCACUGCCGCUUACAUUCAUGAUACCUCAUUUCUAUGACACAAUUUCUAAGUAGGUUUCACCCUAAAGUUUUAUUUUUUAUGCCAUUACUUAAAUGUUUAUCAUUUUAUCCCACUGAUAAUGGAACACAAAUAGAAACUUUUUAUAAUGAAGAUACAAUCCCAACUCAGAGUAAUUAUUUAUAGAUUGGAGAAAGUCUUCACAUAUUUUGUUAUUAUGUGGAUAAGUUCACAAUCAUCAGGAAGAUGCAGAGAAAAAUCAAAACAUGUUACAUCCAAAAUUGAUUUUAGCAUCUUUUUUAAACAAAGUCAUAUUGCUCUUCUGUGCUUAAUAUAUAUGUAUAGAGAAAUAAAAGCUGGUAACAUAAUUAGUUUUUUCUACCUUUAUAAUAAAUGUGUUUUUGGCUGGGCGUGGUAGCUCACGCCUCUAAUCCCAGCAGGUUGGGAGGUGGAGGUAGGUGGAUCACCUAAGGUCAGGAGUUUGAGACCAGUCUGACCCAUAUGGUGAAACCCCGUCUCUACUAAAAAUACAAAAAUUAGCCAGGCAUGGUGGUGCACACCUGUAGUCCCAGCUACUCAGGAGGCUGAGACAGGAGAAUUGCUUGAACUCGGGAGGCAGAGGUUGCAGUGAGCUGAGAUUGUGCCACUGCACUCCAGCCUGGGUGACAGAGUGAGACUCCAUCUCAAAAAUAAAUAAAUAAAUAAAAAUAAAAAAUAAAUGUGUUUUCUGUUAAGUAUUGGAGCGCCAAGUAAGUGAGAACCUGUCACUUUUCCAAAAAAUUAUUUUCAUAUCUGUUUCAUAGCAUGAUUACUUGAUAAUAACUAAUUAAAGUAAAUCUUAUUACUUAUAAGGUAGAUUUCAAACAUAGGUUUAUGGGGGUUUUAAUAACUAUGACAGUGAUAUCUUGAGCUUUUAAGAUUAUUUUCAUACCAUCCAUUAAUUUCCAAAGAGAGAAACUAAUUCACACUACAUUCAGAAUCUAGAUAAAAUCUAACCCAACAUUUGAAACUCUAACCCAGAGUUUUUUGCCUUAAAAAAAAAAAUCUCCUGUGUUAAGGAAACCACUCCCAGUCUUAACAAUAAAACCCAGAUUCUGCAGAUUGUCAAUAAUAGGAAAGUCUCACAUGAGACUCAUAGCUCCAAUUCUCUUUCCCUGUGUUCCUUGAGAGUUCCUUUCAGGAGAUAUGUUUCCAUUAGCUGUUUGCUUUCAUCACCACAAUUACUUCACAGGGCUUUCUGCUUUCAUAAUUGAUCAAUAUAGCUUUCCUGAUUAUAGCCAAUAGAACGUCUGAUACAAGGCUGGAUUCUUCAAAAGACCCAGGGAAAGCAAAGGAUAACAACAAGGAACUGAAUCAUCUGGCCGUGAAAUAACCACCUACUCUCCAGGGUCACCUGCCUCAAUUACACCGUGACCCCAUUUCUUCCUCAGUGUGGUUGAGGACCUAUCUUAGAACUUGUUACCUAGGAGACUCUUCUAACACUUUCACAUUCCUCAAAGCUUAGACAUAUGUCUGUCAACCAGAAAACAGUUUCUUUUUUCACCCCUUGAGAGCCUUCUUCUGAGUUUAUUUUCUUUUUCAAGGAGGUAUCUUAUUCCAGGAUGAAGGAAGUACCUCGUUCCAAGAUGAGUUAGGAGCAUGACUAUUGCUCAUCAUUGGAUGACAAUCAGAAAUAGUCUUAUUCUUUAUGAAAACCACAACAGAAUAGUAACUACCUUAGUAUACCUCAGUGCACCCAGCAUUCACAUAGGAGGUGUGCACGGGAGCAACAGGGAAGCAGUUCAUUUGAAUUUCUCCAUAAACUGCUUUACUUUGAUUAUCUAAACCAAUGGAGCUAUAAUAAUGGGGGGUGGAGGGAAAAGGCCUAACUACCUGAGUAGGAAUCAUGAGACAAAACUUUGUAGUAAAAUAAAAUAAUAACCAAAUGGAGAAUCUCAUUGUGUUUUUUAGGCCUGACUCAGAUGGUCAACAUCUAUGUGAAUUUGAGUAAGGGACAUUUUGUCUGAUGGUGACAGUGUCCUCAGUUGUAAAAUUCCUACAGUCUUUUUCAUAUGUAUGAGUUACAGUAUAAUUCUUCAAAGUGAAAACUGCCUAAAUAAUUAUAAGCCCUACUUUUUGUUACUUAUGAAAAAAUAAUUUUAUUUGAUUUUUAUAUUUUCUUCCCCCCACUGCCAGCUUUAUUAAGGUAUAAUUGACAAAGAAAGAUUGUCUGUAUUUAUGGCAUAAAACCUGAUGUUUUGAUAUUGUAAAUAUUGUGAAAUGAUUACCACACUCAAGCUAAUUAGCAUAUCCAUCAACUUAGUUAUAUAAAUAUAUAUAUAUUUAUUUUAUAUAUAUAUAUAUAUAUAUAUAUUUGUAGUUAGAACAUGUAUUAGUCCAUUUUCAUGCUGCUGAUAAAGACAUACCCGAGACUGGGCAAUUUACAAAACAAAAAGGUUUAUUGGACUUACAGUUUCACGUGGCUGGGGAGGCCUCACAAUUACAGCAGAAGGUGAAAGGCAUGUCUCAAAUGGCAGUGGCAAGAGAGAGAAUGAGAGCCAAGAGAAAUAGGUUUCCCCUUAUCAAACCAUCAGAUCUCAUGAGACUUAUUCACUACCAUGAGAACAGCAUGGGGGAAACCGCCCCCAUGAUCCAACCAUCUCCCACCAGUUUCCUCCCACAACAUGUGGGAAUUAUGGGAAUACAAUUCAAGAUGAGAUUUGGGUAGGGAUACAGAGCCAAACCAUAUCAUUCCACCCAUUACCCCUCCCAAAUCUCAUGUCCUCAUAUUUCAAAACCAAUCAUGCUUUUCCAAAAGUCCCCCAAAGUCUUAACUCAUUUCAGCAUUAACUCAAAAGUCCACAGUCCAAAGUCUCAUCUGAGACAAGGCAAGUCCCUUCCACCUAUAAGCCUGUAAAAUCAAAAGCAAGUUAGUUACUUUCUAGAUACAAUGGGGGUACAGUAAUUGGGUAACUACAACUGAUCCAAGUGGAAGGAAUUGGCCAAAACAAAGGGACUACAGAGUACCCCAUGCAAGUCCAAAAUCCAGCAGGGCAGUCAAAUCUUAAAGCUCCAAAAUGAUCUCCUUUGACUACAUGUCUUAUAUCCAGGGCAUGCUGAUGUAAGAGGUAGGUUCCCAGGGUCUUGGGCAGCUCCACCCCUAUGGCUUUUCAGGGUACAGCCUCCUUUCCAGCUGCUUUCACAAGCUGGUGUUGAGUGUCUAUGGCUUUUCCAGGCAAAUGGUGCAAGCUGUCAGUGGACCUACCAUUCUAGGGUCUGGAAGACAGAUUCUUCUCAUAGCUCUUCUCAUAGCUCCACUAGGAGGUACCCCAGUAGGGACUCUAUGUGGGGGCUCCAACCCCACAUUUCCCUUCCACAUUGCCCUAGCAGAGGUUCUCCAUGAGAGCCCGACCCCUGCAACAACCUUCUGCCUGAGCAUCCAGGCAUUUCCAUACAUCUUCUGAAAUCUAGGCGGAGGUUCCCAAACCCCAUUUCUUGACUUCUUUGCACUUGCAAGCUCAACACUACAUGGAAGCUGCCAAGGCUUGGGUUUCACCAUCUGAAGCCAUGGCCCGAGCUCUACAUUGGCACCUUUCAGUCACAGCUGGAGCAGCUGGGACCAAGGGCACCAAGUUCCUGGGCUGCACACAGCCCAGGGACCCUGGACCCAGCCCCCGAAACCAUUUUCUCCCAGGCCUCCAGGACUGUGAUGGGAGGGGCUGCCAUGAAGACCUCUGACAUAACUUGGAGACAUUUUCCCCAUUUUUUUUGGAAAUAACAUUUGGCUUCUCAUUACCUAUGCAAAUUUCUGCAUCUUGAAUUUCUCCUCAGAAAAUUGGUUUUUCUUUUCUAUCACAUUGUCAGGCUGCAAAUCUUCUGAACUUUUAUGCUUUACUUUCCUUGUAAAACUGAAUGCCUUUAACAACACCCAAGUCACCUCUUGAAUGCUUUGCUGCUUAGAAAUUUCUUCUGCUAGAUACCCUAAAUCAUCUCUCUCGAGUUCAAAAUUCCACAAAUCUCUAGGGCAGGGGCAAAAUGACACCAGUCUCUUUGCUAAAGCAUAACAAGAGUCACCUUUGCUCCAGCUCCCAACAAGUUCCUCAUUUCCAUCUGAGACCACCUCAGCCUGGAUCUCAUUGUCCAUAUGGCUAUCAGACUUUUGGCUAAAGCCAUUCAACGAGUCUGUAGGAAGUUCAAAACUUUCCCAUAUUUUCCUGUCUUCUUCUGAGCCCUCCAAACUGUUCCAGCCUCUGCCUGUUACCCAGUUCCAAAGUCGCUUCCACAUUUUCGGGUAUCUUUUCAGCCACACCCCACUCUACUGUUACCAGUUUACUGUAUUAGUCCAUUUUCCCGCUGCUGAUAAAGACAUACCCGAGACUAGGCAGUUUACAAAAGAAAGAGGUUUAUUGGACUUAUGGCUUCACGUGGCUGGGGAGGCCUCACAAUCAUGGUGGAAGGUGAAAGGCAUGUCUCACAUAGCGGCAGCAGGAAAGAAUGAGAGCCAAGUAAAACAGGUUUCCCCUUAUCAAACCAUCAGAUCUUGUGAGACUUAUUCACUACCACGAGAACAGCAUGGGGGAAACCACCCCCACAAUCCAACUAUCUCCACCAGGUCCCUCCCACAAUACGUGGGAAUUAUGGGAGUACAAUUCAAGAUGAGAUUUGGGUGGAGACACAGAGCCGAACCAUAUCAGAACAUUUAAGAUCUACUUUCUUAGCACACUUCAAGUACACACUAGAGUGUUUUCAAUAUAGUCAUCAUGCUGUACAUUAGGUCUCCAGAACAUAUUCAUCCUGCCUAACUGAAACUUUGCACCCUUUGAUCAACAUCUCACAAUUUCCACUACUCCCCAGCUCCUGGCAACCACCAUUCUAUUCUCUGUUUCUAUGAGUUUGAUUCCACAUAUAAUUGAGAUCAUGCAAUAUCUUCCUUUCUGUGCCUGGCUUAUUUUACUUAGCAUAAUGCCCCCAAGUUUCAUUCAUGUUUUCACAAAUGACAACAUUUCCUUCUUUUUUAAGGCUAAGUUUUCAACAUUAUAUAUACAAUAAAGAAAGUUUCCUCAAGAAAGAAAACUUUUUUUGUUAUUUUACCUAGUUUCUAUUCCUUUUGGAUCUUUUUCUUUCAAAAUUAAAGCAAAUAACUAUGAUCGUAUGGUCAUUUGGUAUACAUAUAUGUAUAACACAUUUUUUAUAUCCAUCAGUAGACACUGAGGUUGAUUUUAUAUCUUGGCUAUUGUAAAUAAUGCUGCAAUAAACAUGGGAGUGCACAUAUCCAUUCUAGACACUGAUUUCAUUUAAUUGGAUAUAUACCCAGAAGUGAGAUUGCUGGGCCAAAUGGUAAUUCUAUUUUUAAUUUUUUAAGAACCUCCAUACUGUUUUCUGUAAUGGCUGUACCAAUUUACAUUCCAACCCAUGGUACAAAGGGUUAUUUUUCUCAGCAUCUUCCCUAAUACUUAUUAUCUUUUGUCUUUUUGAUAAUAGACAUUCUAAUAUGUGUGAAGUAAUAGAUAACUCAUUGUGGUUUUGAUUUACAUUUCUUCGAUUAUUAGUGAUGUUGAAUAUCUUUUCAUAUAUCUGUUGGCCAUUUGUAUAUCUUCCUUUGAGAAGUGCCUAUUCAAGUAGUCCUUUAUUCAUUUUUAAAAUUGAGUCAUUUGUUUUCUCUUUAUUAAGUUGAGUCCCUUAUAUAUUUUGUACAUUAGCUCCUUAUCAAAUGUUUGCAAAUUUUUCUCCCAUUCUGUAGAUUUUCUCCAGUCUGUUGAUUGUUUCAUUUGCUACAGGGAAACUUUUUAGUUUGAUAUAAUUCCAUUUAUCUAUUUUGCUUUUGUCAGCUGUGCUUUAUAAGGAGUGAUAUCCAAAAAAAUUAUUGCCCAGACCAAUGUCAAAAUGCUUUUUUCACAUGUUUUCUUCUAGUAGUUUUACAGUUUAUGUUCAAUUCUAUAAUCCAUUUCAAGGAAUUUUUGUAUGUGAUGUGAGUUAAGGGUCCAAUUUCAUUUUUCUGCAUAUGGAUAUCCAUGUUUUUGUGCCCAUGAUAUCCUUAAAUGAGAAGUAAGUGCUGGGUGCAAAUUAGGGGAAGACAUCAUACAAUUUGUGAAACCUUACUGAAUUAUGUAUUUGAUAAAUAAUAAAAAGUGGAACUUUUUCCACAUAAUUCAUUUUAUUAGGACAAAGAGUUUGACAUCUGAUUGUAUUAUGAAAACUAAGUGUAAAAAGUACAGUGAAGGUAAUCCUUUCUAUGUAGACUUUAACUGGGGUAUUUAAUACAAAAGGUUGGUCUUGUAUCCCAGAUCCUGGGGUCUAGUUUAGGAUCUGUCCCAGUUGUCACUGCUUUGUUUUGAUGAAAUUCUUAAAGUUAGCAUAAUCUGUAUCUGAUAUUCCAACCAUCUUAACUUUUAAAAUCCAAGUCCCUAUCACUCUUUAGAUUUGAUCUAAGAAAAUGUUAUAAUAUUGACCACUUACUAGAAGAUACUGAUAUCACGAUAGAGUGAUAUUGAGUUUUCCCAAGUCUUAUUUCAUAAGCCAAGGCCUUUUUAAAAAUAAAGAUUAUUUAAUUUAGAAUAGAGCUUGGCACAUAGAAAAUAUGCAGAUGGUUUAAAUGACAUUAUAUCAAGAAGUUGCAACUUUGGCAUAAAUUUGUAUGGCAGAGAAGGACAAAAAGGGAAUGACAAAAAAUAACCAAGUAGAAUGAAUGCAGAAGUAGAAUAAUCUCUCUAAUAAUGCAGAUAAGGGAACCCCCAGGUGAGUUCACACUGGCUUCACCUGGUUCCACAAAGACCGGUUUAUAGACCAGAGGUUCUCAAGGACUGAGCCCUAUCUGGGACCCCUGCCCACCUGCAGGGGGUGAAAUCAACUCCUCAGAGGCCUGUCCACCCGCACCACAGAAAAUACUUAAAAUCGUCUCUCCAGCUCACACAAAACCAUCACACAAGCUAACAUUAAAAAUAAUUAUACCCACUAAGUCAUCAGUCUAUAAUUAGUGUUUUUUUCUUCAGAAACGUGGUGAAGAAGGCAAAGCAUUUGACUUCUGAGGUCAAAUAGGUUCUUGUCAUUCUCUUGACCACUUUAGCGUAAUUUGAGACCAUGUAAAUUAGGAAAGAAAUGUUCACUACCACAGCAGAGAGUGAUUGAUCAUCAAAAGGGCCUCAGUUAGGUGUCACCUGGUCCUUUUAAAUGCGUCCCUCUGCUCCUGAUAUUGCUGACCACAACAGUCAGGACUUUAGUGAGAAGUUGAAAACUUGUUUUAGAUAAUAUAUAUUUUCAUUGGAGAGAAAUAGGGCUCCAAUUUCAAAUUUCUUCUCUACACUGGGUUCUCUUCCUUCCCAGUGAAAUAAUUCUCUUUUAUUCUCUAUAUCCAGUUAACGUUUAUUGAUUCCCUGUUGUGAGUAGAUAUGUCUAUUGCAUCUGCUAUUGCCUGUGACCACUUCCUCAUUCUUUGUCUUUCCUUCUCUCCCAAGAUGUCACAGCAACACUCUUCACAACAGAUUGCCGUUAUAUUGCUUUGUUUUGUUUUAAAGAGAAACGUCAUAGGGCUUAUGGAGGGAGGUAGUUUUCAAAAGAUAUAACUUUUUUGAGAGCCAUAGCUUAGCCAGUUUGAAAAGUUGUACAGCUGCAAAAGCUGUAUGGAAACUCCUAUAAAUUAAAUUUUUACACAUCCUUCCUCUAUCCUUUGCUUUAUGAAUAAAUAUUGGUAUAUGCUGAUGGCCAUAUGCCUUUAUAUUGUGUUAUUACUUAGAAUUGCCUGGCAGCAAAAAUCAUGGAGUUCAUUUAAAAAUCAAUGUAAUGCCAAAUUUAUAAAAUUUAGUGCAGACUGUCAUAUAAUGACAACUCUUUAGAUUCUCAGUUUACAUCUCAUUUCCACAUCCAAUAUCUGAUUGCAAUCUCAUUUGACAGUUAAGAAAAUUGAAACAUAGAGAGGAAAGUGAUUUACCCAAGGUUGCUCAGUUGGGGAAAUGGCUGGAUCUGGCUGACUCCCAUUCCAGUAAUUUUUCCACCUUUGUUGCUGAUUCUUGGUGGUAGUUAGGUUUUCCUUGUUUUUCUAAUUCUCUGUUGAAAUGUACAAUGGUAGCAAAAAGAAAAAUGAGUAAAAGAAAAAUGUAUUUAGUACAAAUUUAUUAACAUACCAUAAGAAAGCUCUUCUAUACUGCAAAUUUGUAUUUUUGAAAAAUAGACUGGCCAGGUGCGGUGGCUCAUGCCUGUAAUCCCAGCACUUUGGGAGGCUGAGGCGGGCAGAUCACCUGAGGUCAGGAGUUCAAGACCAGCCUGGCCAACUUGGUGAAACCCCAUGUCUACUUGAAAUACAAAAAAUUAGCUGGGCGUGGUGGUACGCACCUGUAAUCCCAGUUACUCGGGAGGCUGAGGCAGGAGAAUCACUUGAACCCAGGAGGCAGAGGCUGCAGUGAGCUGACAUCGUGCCAUUGCACUCCAUCAUGAUUGAAAAUUUCCUGAGACCUCCCCAGAAGCCAAGUAGAUGCCAGCAUCAUGCUUCCUGUACGGCCUAUGGAACCAUGAGCCAAUUAAACCUCUUUUCUUUAUAAAUUACUAGUUUCAGGUAUUUCUUUGUAGCAAUGCGAGAACAGACUAUUACAACAAUUGUGAAAAGCAGUUUGGCAUUUUUUUCAAAGAACUCAAAAGCAGAAUUGCCAUUUGCCCUGGCAAUUCCAUUAUUAGGUAUGUACCCAAAGGAAUAUAAAUUGUUCUAUUAUAAAGACACAUGCAUGCAUAUGUUCAUCACAGCACCAUUCACAAUAGCAUGGAUAUGGAAUCAACCUAAAUGCCUAUCAGCAGUAGACUGGAUAAAGACAAUGUGAUACAUACAUACUGUGGAAUACUAUGCAGUCAUGAAAAAGAGCAGGAUCACAUCCUUUGCAGCAACACAGAUGGAGCUGGAGGCCAUUAUCCUUAGCAAACUAACACAGGAACAGAAAACCAAAUACCACAUGCUCUCACUUAUAAGUGAGAGCUAAACACUGAGUACAUAUGGACACAAAGAAGGGAACAACAGACACUAGGCCCUACUUGAGGCUGGAAGGAGGGAGCAGGGUAAGGAUCUAACUGACUAUUGGGUUUUAUACUUAUUACUUAGAUGGUGAAAUAAUCUGUACACCAAGCCCCCAUGAGAUGCAAUUUAUCUAUAUAACAAAUGCAUAUAUACCCUGAAUCUAAAGUAAAAGUUAAAAAAUACAUAUUUGCUCAAUAGUAAUAAUUUUAAAAGAGACUGAAAUACAGUGACACUGAGGAGUUUGGCUAACACUCACCAUGAUGAAUUGUUCUUCAACUUUGGAGAGACCAAGAGUAGACUUUUUUUGAUCCACUGCUUCAUUUUUCCAGAAAUUUGUUCUAAAAGGUCUUAAAAAAGAAAUCUGUAGAAAACUUAGUAGCAUAAAAGUAUAAUUUUACUAACAAAACUGGAAACAAAUAUGUACUUUCAAAUAGAGAAAUGUAUAAAUAAGCUAUAUCAUAUUAAUUUAAAAUAUUUUGCAGGCAUUGAAAAUAACAAAUAUAUAAAUAUUUUAUUUGUCUAUUUUACAGUUUACCUAGUGUUUUAUAUCUCAUUUAAAGAUUGGAGGUACAACUAAAAAUGCUUAUAAAAUAUUCUAAGUGAAAUAAUAAAUAAAAAAUGUAUAUGUGUACUAUGACUACAACCACAUAAAGCUCUACCCAUGAAAAAGAUUGGAAUAGACAUAUAUAUGCAUUUAUAUUCAUAUGCAGGUAAAUAGGCAUACUGUACAGGUGAUGAGCCUAUAGAUAUAAUUUUCUUUAAUAUUAAGAUCUUUAAAUUUAAAUAGAAACUUGUUUUCAUAGUAAAUUCCUAAAUUUUGAACAGAUAUGAUCAUUACGUUGAGUAGAUUAAACUUGAAAAAGUUGUCUUCUUAAUGAUAACAUAUAAUCCAUAAGACAAAUAUUUUACUAUUAUUAUGAUUAUUCUGAGAUAGGGUCUCACUCUGUUUCCCAGGCUGGGGUGCAGUGGCACAGUCAUAGCUCACUGCAGCCUCAAACUCCUGGGCUCAAGUAAUCUCCCUGCCUCAGUCUCUUGGACAGCCUCUAGACUACAAGCACAUGGCAUCAUGCCUGUUUAAUUUUUUAAAAAUACUUUGUAGAAAAAAUAUCUCACUGUGUUGCCCAUGCCCAUGCUGGUCUUGGACUCUUGGCCUCAAAUGAUCCUCCUGCCUCGUCCUCUUAAAAUGAUGGGGUUACAGGUAUGAGUCACCAUGCCCAGCCUAUUAUUUUUAUAUGAAGGCAUAAAUUAUUAAUUUUUUAAUUAGUUUUUAAAUCAACCAAGAUGAGAUUUAGAAUAAUAUCAGAUCAUUACAUAAAAAUAUAAUUUAGGUGUAUUCAAACUUUAUUCAGCUUCCAAAAAUAACUCGAAUGAUAACACUAUUACUUAAAGAGUAGGAAUAAUGCAAACCUAUGCAUUAUUUUGGUUACAGGCCAAAGCGAAGAUAAAACAUAUGUAAAAGUAUUUACUGUUUUUCUUAAGAGAGUUUAUUGGUGAUUGUUGUUUUGAAAAUAUUACAGGUUUAUAUUUUUGAGCUCUAGCUCAAUAGUAUCUGAGGAGCAUAGUGAACUUACAAUUUCAUUUGUGUUGACUUUCUAGUUAAAGAAUAAAUCCCUUUCCUUUGAAAUGUAGCCUUGGUCAGCUGAUGGAGCAUUUUCUCCAUAUAUGCAUGUUAGGAAAAUUUGUUUCAAUUUAAAAAGGAAACACAUGGCUAUGACUUAACUAUUAAAAAGUGAAAUGUUCAAUUAAUGUGGAUUUGGUCUUUCUGUUUUUCCAGUCCCUCAAAUGUUAUUUCAACAAACCAAAAAAUGAGUUUUUUGGUUUGUUGAAAUAACAAACCAAAUAACAAGCCAAGUCCAAAUAUUCUGACUUGGCUUAAGACUUUUGUGCUGAAGACUCUGUUCCCAAGAAGAUUUACAUUGAGGACCCAAGUCUGCCAUUUAAUUAACAGGCUGUUUGUUGAUUUCUUGUAAUGCUGAAUUAUUUACCAGCUGUCUCCUGGUUAUGUCAGAAAGAUGUAAAGAAUGCAAACAAAAAUACAAAAUAAGACACAGGUAACAUCAGCAAUGUAAUCUCUCCCCAUGCACCCUGCUCACCUCCAAACCAAUAUAUGUUGCUGUUACAGAGGAGAUCUCUCUGAAAUACGUGUUCAUGCAACACAAUAUUUUAGAAGACAAUACAUUUUCUUGAUCAUACAUGUGUUGUUAGUUCACCAUUUCUUUUUUAGAAAUAAGCAGUUACCCCAAGACUAUGAUUAUACAUUCAUGAAUGUAUUAUGCUCUUUAUAUUUAUACCAUAUCUAUUCUCUUUAUAUUUGAAUUUAUAUGCACUUGCUCCUGCACACACAUACACACACCUGCCAUAUUCCCUGUAUCACUUUUUUAUAUUUUAAAAAUCAGUGAAGUCCAAAGUACACUAUAUUUCCUUAUAUUAUAGGACAGCAGCAUCUAGAAUUUUGUUAUGUGUACCCAUGAAUAUUUUUAAUGCAGAUGAUGAGAGUAAUGGUAAUAACAUGUCUGAAAACUGGAAUUUUUUCACUUGGCAGUGAUUAUAAGCAUGACAAAUUAACUUUGUCAAAAAAACUUCAAAAAUGAUCUCUUUAUUAUGAACUAGAGUUACUAUUUUCUGCUCUUUCUUUCUUUCUUUCCUUCCUUCUUUCACUACAUUGUAGUAGUGGCCAUUGAAGAACAUUUAGAAAAUGCUAAAAGAUCAGAAAGAAAAUAAAAUUGCUGUAAUUUCACUACCUAGAGAUAAAAACUAUUAACAUCAUAGUGCAUAUUUUCAGAUUUUUCUAUAUAUUGAAUAUUUAUUACAAAAUUCGGAUCAUAUUGUACCUACUAUUUUCUAAUAUGCCUUACUCAGUAAUGUAUCAUAAAAUAUCUUAUGAAAAUCCUAACACAGUCCUCUAAUUUCAGUGUGAUUGCAUCAUGGCAUAUGAAUAUACUUUUAGUCAUUUAAGAACUAGGGGCAUUGACACUAAUGCUUUUGAAGGCUUUUCCCUCAAGGAUUCAGUUGGUGGCAACAGGAGCACCAAUGUUCCCAUGUGUCCCAGGCUUUCUGAAGGAACCCCACAUGCAGUGUUUUGAUGGAACAGCAGCUGACACUGUUAUCACUCAGCUCAGGCAGCUGGGUGCCUGAGGGCCUUUCCUGGCCAUGAGCCACCUGACUAAAAUGGCUUAUGCUUUAGGUGUGUGUGUUUGGGGAGGGGGUACAAUUAUACUACGAGGCUGUAUUUUGACAAAGAUUUCAAAUAUGUUCAAUGACCUUGUUUGUACAUCUUAAAGCUUUAAGUGCCCAGGAAUUCCUUCUCCGGAGUUCACAAAGGGAUAAUCUUCAGGUUCCUUCCUUCCUUCCUGCCUUUCUCCCUUCUUCCCUAGCUCCCUCCCUUCCCUCCCCUCCCCUCCCCUCCCCUUUCUUCCCUUUCUUUCUUCUUUUUCUUUUUCUGAAACCACUUAAAUGUAUUUAGGAAACUUUGAAUGAAAGUAAGACAUUGGUUCUUUACAUCUUAAGAUAGAAAAGGCAUUAAGAAGUACAUCUUUCCCAUCUAGAAAAAUAUUACCAUCCAGCAAAAAAACACAAUUAUAUUUAGAAAUACAGUAAAUUAUGACUGCUCAGAAGGUGUUUAAUUUCAUGGUUUUAACUCUAUAGCUGUGCCACAUUUUCUAGAAUAGGUUAAGAGACCUCAUACAGAUUAUCUUUAAACAUCUACAUAAGAUGGUUGCUAAAAGCUUUCACAUUUUGGAUUACUUUCAUUUUUAUGCCUAAAUGACUUUCAGUGUUUCGACAGUAUUUGCUCUUCACAGCUUAUAAGUAUUAUCAUUUGGAGUUGUUUCUAAGGCCUAAAUAAAAAAGCCACAUGGAAGGGAGUGGCAGGGGAAAUGUGUUAGAAAAAUACUUGUCUUCAUUAGUUCACACACUAGAAACAACCCCAUCCGACUCAUCCAUGAACCCAGUACUACCCUAAGUGGAAAUACUACAAGGAUUUCAGGCCAGACCUUCAUGAGUAUCUGUGUGAAAUGAAACAUUGCCUCUAGGAAACAUCAGGAAGGUAUCAUUACUGGGCAAGGUAGCAUGAACCAAAUAGAAAACCAAAACAUCUUAUUUAUUCUCCUCACUGAUUGCAAAUGUCGACCAAUUCUUCUGGAUGCUUUCUUCUUCAUACUUUUAAACUUCAGUGCAAGUGUCUUUUCCAUAUAUGAUUCUAAAAUCCGGAUCUUAAAAUCCAAGAGGAAAAAAAAACAACAUAGAGGUUCAGAGACAAAGGGAGGAAGCAAUGUGCUCUUAUUUUCUGCCAUGGUAAUUACACUAGGGCAAUACUAGCAGUAGUGUUUGAGAAACUAAAUACCCGGCCAGGUUGGUAGCUCAUGCCUGUAAUCCUAGCACUUUGGGAAGCCAAGAUGGUUGGAUCACCUCAGGUCAGGAGUUCAAGACCAGCCUUGCCAACAUGGAGAAACCCUGUCUCUACUAAAAAUAUAAAAAUUAGCCAGGUGUGAUGGCAUGUGCCUGUAAUCCCAGCUACUAGGGAGGCUGAGGCAAGAGAAUCACUUGAACCUGGGAGGCGGAGGUUGCAGUGAGCCAAGAUCAUGCCACUGCACUCCAGCCUGGGCAACAGAGCAAGACUUCAUCUCAAAAAAACGAAACGAAACAAAACAAAAAAAAAGAAAAGAAAAGAAAAGAAAUACCUUAGUGGGGCAGUAUAAUAAUUUGAAGAAAGUGCCUAAAACUCUGUUUCCACUUUUAUUGUUUUUCAAUUGAGAUAUCUGAAUAAUUGAAAACUGACUUCAGAUAAGAUUUAAAACAUUUACAGCUGGGAAUGACACUUACUUAAAGGGUAGAACACAGACACAUACAUGUAGCCCUGCAGUUCAGACUCUGCCUCUAGCUUUCCAAUAAAAUUGGUUGAAAGAACCUGCCAAUUUAUUAACAUCCUCAAACCCAGGAGAAAAUUAUGGCUACUGUACUAUAUUCCACACUACAGUUGAAAAAAAGUGUUCUGCUACAUCGAAGGUCAAGAGAUUGCCUUGCUUCCUUAAGAGCAUUGUUAAAGGUCUGAUAAUUUAAGAAAAUUAAGAUAAAAUAAUGCAUUAUGUGUAUGUUACAAAAACCAGAGUAAUAGUCUACUAUACAGAAAGACUUCUGAACUUGCUUCUUCAAUUGAAAAACAAGCAGGACCCAAUUUAAAAAAUAAGUAUUGGCACUAGUAAUAAAAACUGAUUUUUCCUUUCUGCAUCCUGCAAUGAAUUCAUUGUUAAAAAAAAUCAAAACUCAUUUUUCUAAAAAUCUCUGGACUCUUUGUAAAAGUUAACUUUCCUAGUCAAUAUCCUCAAGAAGUUUUCCGGGUGACUUGUAUUCUUGUCUUCCCUAUUCUCACUAUAUAAAAACCACACUUUAUUUCCUUUCUUUUUCUGAGAAAGCUGUAAGGUAACUAAUUUACUCAGACUAUGGAACUCUAGACCAUGCAGAUCUUGAUUGUAAUUCUAACUUCACCAUUGACCUUUAACAGUGUACAGGUUAAUUAUGCUUAUCUGUAAAAUAAGAAUAACAGGUAUCUCCUAGGAUUAUUAUGAGAGCUAACUGAGAUAAUAUACAUAAAGUUCCCAGCUCCCAGCCCUGUGUGUCUCAUAAGACGGGUGGCCACAUUUUCAGUUCCUUUCCUGUUCUCCACCUGUCUCCCUCCCUCUGUUCCCCGCCCCUCUCCACAACUCGACCUCUAAAAAAUGCUUAAGUAAUUGUAGAGAAAUUAGCAUGAAUGCCCAGAUGCAUUUGUUACUGAAUAACUCAGCAGUGAACUUGGCAUUCCAUAGCUAACCUUUCCCCUUCAUUAAUCCCCUUCUCCAUCCCCCUCAAACACAGGAGUACAACAGGAUGCCAGGCGAACUAUGUAACCAACCAUGCACGUGAGCAUUUUCUCCCAGAAUUUUGACUAGUCUUGUUCUGCCUCAAACACUAGACGGGGCUCAUGCUGCUCACAAUUAACUGACUCUGGCCAUGUGGUGGCUGCCCUCAAGAUCUGCCACAAAGAGAACAGCAGUUCAAUAAAAUCUCGAACUCUAUUUAUAGCCCACUUGAAACAAGCAGUUUCCUUGAAGCCCAAGAAGCCCUCCUUGAGAAUGCAGCAAGUAAUUUACUAGUCCCAGUACUCACUGGGGAAAUAAGAGGGAGGAAAUGCAGCAAGUGCAUUUUUUCAAGUACUGCACAUAUAGAAAGCAUUUUGUCCUACACUCUGUCCCAUUUCACCCUGAUGUCACCAGCCAAGGAAGUAGACAAAACAGGCACUAGUAAGAAAUCUCUGUUUUAUAGAUUACAAAACUGACACCUAGGAGGUUAAAUUGCUAAUGAACAGUGGUGGUUGGAGAAGGAGGUUAAAAAAAUUGUCUAAAGGGUGAGAAUAAUUUCUUGCUCAUGCAAUCAAUCUAAAAUUCAGUUAAGUCAUUAUUUACCUAUUAAAAAAUAUAUACAACUAAGAAGAAAUGUUUUGUAAGGCACUUGCAAGAUUAAAAAUUGUUCCUUCUCCACUUCUAAGAAGAUCAAAAUAUGAGAAAUAAAAACUUAGACUCUACAGGGAAAUAUUUAUUAACACGUUUGUAUCUAUUUAUAAUAUAUACAUUCAGAGUGAUUAUAUUUUUGGCAAGAAAUGCCUUCUUGAAGACCCCCAAAAUUAAAGUGUGCAUGCAUAAUCGAGACUGAUUUUGAAAGAUGAUAGGAAUUUUUAUGAGAAAUUUAAAUUGAUUCUGUCAGCUCUGAAAUAAAUACAUCUUUACUAUAUUUUAAUAUGGAAGUUUGCAUAAUUCCAGUAUGUAUGCAAAAUGCAAGACUUUAUUAUAUGAGUUUAUGGGCCAGAAAUCAUUUUGCUCUUAGAAUUAAUUUGAUUUUGGCAAAUACUUCAAUUUUCUAAGAUCCUUCUUUAAGCCCUGUUACCUGGAAACCUGAAAAAAAUAAACAACUUUUGGGCUUGAGAGGGAUGUCUGGGCAAUUAGAAUAGCUACACUGAAGUCUGCCCGUGUGUGUGUGUGUGUGUGUGUGUGUGUGUGUGUGUGUGUGUGUGUGUGUGUGUGUUUAGAGAGAGAGAGAGAUUAUUGCUUAAACAGUGCCCCUGGGUUGGUUGCUUGGCUUGGUGCCAUUUGGGAUUCUCAGAUUUUAUUGUCCCAGCUCUGAUUUACGGAGUUCAGAAUCUCGAAAGGCAAGGUGUCUGGAGUUUAGGGUCUUUCCAUGACAGCCCCUCCUCUUCCCUGUACACUCCUUUUGCUUGUGGUCACCUUGUGGUGACCUUGCAGGACUCAGCGUUUUUACCUGAGCUCAGUAGCUGGGGAGCCCACUAGUGCUGGGGAGCGAGCCGUGGUUUCCAUUCCUGGGUGAUGGAGUCAUGGGAGAAACUGCAGUGAGCAAACACAGUAGGACCUGAGUUGGGCUCGAAUGUGCUUUAAGCGACUCAGGACAGAGCAGCUGCUCUGUCUCCCAGCUUGCAAGUGCAGCCUGCAUUUGUCACUGACCACUGAAGUGUAUGUUUGUGCAAGGUGAGAGCUGGGUGCUUUGUUCUUAAUUUGGAGACAAAUUGCCAGGAGGCGAUCGAGAUCGGAUGACAGCAAAUCAUGAAAGCUACCUCCUCAUGGCAAGCACCCAGAAUGAUAUGGAAGACUGGGUGAAGUCAAUCCGCCGAGUCAUAUGGGGACCUUUCGGAGGAGGCAUUUUUGGACAGAAACUGGAGGAUACUGUUCGUUAUGAGAAGAGAUAUGGGAACCGUCUGGCUCCGAUGUUGGUGGAGCAGUGCGUGGACUUUAUCCGACAAAGGGGGCUGAAAGAAGAGGGUCUCUUUCGACUGCCAGGCCAGGCUAAUCUUGUUAAGGAGCUCCAAGAUGCCUUUGACUGUGGGGAGAAGCCAUCAUUUGACAGCAACACAGAUGUACACACGGUGGCAUCACUUCUUAAGCUGUACCUCCGAGAACUUCCAGAACCAGUUAUUCCUUAUGCGAAGUAUGAAGAUUUUUUGUCAUGUGCCAAACUGCUCAGCAAGGAAGAGGAAGCAGGUGUUAAGGAAUUAGCAAAGCAGGUGAAGAGUUUGCCAGUGGUAAAUUACAACCUCCUCAAGUAUAUUUGCAGAUUCUUGGAUGAAGUACAGUCCUACUCGGGAGUUAACAAAAUGAGUGUGCAGAACUUGGCAACGGUCUUUGGUCCUAAUAUCCUGCGCCCCAAAGUGGAAGAUCCUUUGACUAUCAUGGAGGGCACUGUGGUGGUCCAGCAGUUGAUGUCAGUGAUGAUUAGCAAACAUGAUUGCCUCUUUCCCAAAGAUGCAGAACUACAAAGCAAGCCCCAAGAUGGAGUGAGCAACAACAAUGAAAUUCAGAAGAAAGCCACCAUGGGGCAGUUACAGAACAAGGAGAACAAUAACACCAAGGACAGCCCUAGUAGGCAGUGCUCCUGGGACAAGUCUGAGUCACCCCAGAGAAGCAGCAUGAACAAUGGAUCCCCCACAGCUCUAUCAGGCAGCAAAACCAACAGCCCAAAGAACAGUGUUCACAAGCUAGAUGUGUCUAGAAGCCCCCCUCUCAUGGUCAAAAAGAACCCAGCCUUUAAUAAGGGUAGUGGGAUAGUUACCAAUGGGUCCUUCAGCAGCAGUAAUGCAGAAGGUCUUGAGAAAACCCAAACCACCCCCAAUGGGAGCCUACAGGCCAGAAGGAGCUCUUCACUGAAGGUAUCUGGUACCAAAAUGGGCACGCACAGUGUACAGAAUGGAACGGUGCGCAUGGGCAUUUUGAACAGCGACACACUCGGGAACCCCACAAAUGUUCGAAACAUGAGCUGGCUGCCAAAUGGCUAUGUGACCCUGAGGGAUAACAAGCAGAAAGAACAAGCUGGAGAGUUAGGCCAGCACAACAGACUGUCCACCUAUGAUAAUGUCCAUCAACAGUUCUCCAUGAUGAACCUUGAUGACAAGCAGAGCAUUGACAGUGCUACCUGGUCCACUUCCUCCUGUGAAAUCUCCCUCCCUGAGAACUCCAACUCCUGUCGCUCUUCUACCACCACCUGCCCAGAGCAAGACUUUUUUGGGGGGAACUUUGAGGACCCUGUUUUGGAUGGGCCCCCGCAGGACGACCUUUCCCACCCCAGGGACUAUGAAAGCAAAAGUGACCACAGGAGUGUGGGAGGUCGAAGUAGUCGUGCCACCAGUAGCAGUGACAACAGUGAGACAUUUGUGGGCAACAGCAGCAGCAACCACAGUGCACUGCACAGUUUAGUUUCCAGCCUGAAACAGGAAAUGACCAAACAGAAGAUAGAGUAUGAGUCCAGGAUAAAGAGCUUAGAACAGCGAAACUUGACUUUGGAAACAGAAAUGAUGAGCCUCCAUGAUGAACUGGAUCAGGAGAGGAAAAAGUUCACAAUGAUAGAAAUAAAAAUGCGAAAUGCCGAGCGAGCAAAAGAAGAUGCCGAGAAAAGAAAUGACAUGCUACAGAAAGAAAUGGAGCAGUUUUUUUCCACGUUUGGAGAACUGACAGUGGAACCCAGGAGAACCGAGAGAGGAAACACAAUAUGGAUUCAGUGAGCCUGCUUUCGCCUGCUGUCUCUGAUGGCUCUGGCAAGGACUCCAGGGAUUCUGGUGGGAUAUGACUUAGAACCAGGUGGCUGGUCACCUGGAUGUACAGAAGUCUAACUGGUGAAGGAAUAUCAUUUACAGACAUUAAACAUCCAUAUCUGCAAUGUGUACCAAAGUUAUAUCAUGCCCCAUAAUGCUACUGUCAAGUGUUACAACUGGAUAUGUGUAUAUAGAGUAGUUUUUCAAAAGUAAACUAAAAAUGAGAAGCAUAUUUCAAGAAUUAUUUUAUUGCAAGUCUUGUAUUUAAAUGUUAAAUCAAUAUGUUGUUGCAAUUUAGCUUGCUUUCAAGCUUCACCCCUUGCACUUAACAUAAGCUAUUUUUGGCAUUGUGUUAUCAUCGGCUUAUUUUAUAGAUCAAUAUUUUUAUUUCCCUUUUUUGCUGAGGAAAUGAAGAUAAGCAAAAAUAUAAAUAUAUAUAUAAAUAUAUGAGUUAUUAAAAUCAGAAGAAUACUUUGUGGCUGUGCUGUUUGUGCCAAUAGACUUUGUCAUGACCAAAAAGAGAAAUGUAAAUAGUUUUAUAAAAUACAGUCGAAUCACCAGGAACCUUUGAGCUGCUUUUAAAAUUCUUCCCCUGGCACCACUCAGUUUUGCUUUUGCGAGGCGAUUUGACAUAGGAACUUUGAGACUCCAUGAGAAAGUCCCUUUCUGAGGCCCACUGUCUACCUUGCCAGAUCCUCAGUGCGUAUCGCCAAUGCAGGAUGCUCCUUAGAAAAGAAAAAAUGGUAAAGAAUGGCAUUUAACGAUUCAGGCUUUGAAUUACUCUGUCCCUCUGGACCGAAUCUCUUUAACUGCUGGAUAGUUUUAGAGGAAUUCUCCUGCUACUUAGGUACUGGGAAACAAUGCUUGCUAAACCAUGCCCACGUGAGCACCUGUCUCCCACUCAAACCUCUCCCAUCUCCCAACAACUGCACUUUAGAAUACCAGCAGUGAAAUGGUAUUACUGUUUCCCUCUGAGUGAAACUGCUAGAGUAUAUGUCACGUAGUGACAUUUUUUUCUCACUCAGGCUAUUGCCAUCUGGGAUUCUCUCCCUACUACAGCUGGCAAAGUUGGUUUGCAGCAAGAAGAUAGUGGGAGGGGGCCAGGCUGCAGGAGAAGGAGAAAAGUUUAGAAGAAACAAACCAUUUUGCUUCUAAUUUUGACAGUAUCACUUUCCUGUUAAAACAUACAAUAAUUUUAAAAGGUGAAUGCCUAAAGUUCCAAUUUUAGCAAAUAUGGGAACCUCAGCAAUGCUAAUUUUCUAGAAAAACCCAGGGCUCUUUGGAGCUAGAGUUUUGGGAGAACAGUUCUUCACAAUAAGGCAAUGGUUUUGAGAGGCCAGGCAAAUAAUCUUUCUCACCGUAGAACAAAAAGUUACAAAAGGCAUAAUCGGAAAUAGAGACUACAUACUUGAGUUUAUGGGGUUUGUGUUGUUUGAAGGUUCAAUGCUUGCAUGUGUUUAUUUAUUUUCAAGAGGGAAAGUGGUCUGUACUGCUUUCAUCCUUGCCACUGUCUUGCUUUUAUUUUUUACUCUCCCACUGAGCAAGCGUCUGUGGUCCUAUGGUAUCAACCAGUAUCUUUAUAGCAAUAAUUUCUUUAAUUCCCUUUUCUCUCUCUUUCCAAUUAUUUAACCAGUUACUUCCACCUGGACAUACGAUAGGAAAUUCAAACUCAAAAUAUGAAAAUUGAUCUUAAUAACUCUCCCUUCAUAUCUUUUCACCUAUUUCCAGUCCUUAUCAUAGUUGAUAAAAACCUCAGACUCAUCCAGAAAGCUAUAUGAUGCACUAGUAAAAAAAACAAAGAUAUUCAAACUGCUUGGGUUCAAAUGGUAUACAAUUUGCCAGCUGUUACUGAACCUUCUAUGCAUAACUUUUUUUUUCCUCUGUGCAAUUGGAAUAAUAAAAAUACUACUCCCA